UUCUUCAGUUUUGCUCAUGUCAGCUGAGUGUUUCUCUUUUGAACUGGGAAAUGCCAGAGGCUGGGGGGUGGGAGCCGAUGUCCUCUAAGGGAAAAUUCUCCCCGUUAACACUGCAAAUGUGCCUUAACAUUGUACUUAUUCCUCCAAAAAUAAUUGUUCAGUGGCACAAUGUGGGAUACUUGAAAGAUGUUUGCUGCACAAAGGUUCCAAUACUUACCUGCAGAUUAAGAAAUGAGUUUCUAAACCAUCUCAUUUCUAUUGCUAAUGAAAAGCUUUGGAAGGCACCUGUGAAUUAGAGCUCCAGCUGCUAUCAUGGUAGGGAAGUUAGGCCUUGAAAGGAUACGUGGAUUAGCCUGUCAGAAAAGCAAACAGUAGCAUCAGCACAAGUAGAAAAUAGACAAGGUUGUUAAAGCUAACAGGAAAGUAGGCUAAAGCAUUGCUGUAAUUUUAUAGUGGAAAUUUGCUGGGAAGGAGUGACUGGUUGGAUGGGAGAAGGAAAAGAAGAGAAGCAGGAAAAUAAUUGACUAGCCAAAUUGAAGAAGUCUGUCCACUGGGGAAGAUCCUACAGGAAGAAGUAAGGCAUUGCUUUUAAGAAAGCGAUUAUAGCAAGUAGAAAAAGACCUUGUAAUUUGGUACCUAACACAUGUGAAAUAUGAAGACCAGUGCUCAGGUACACAUUCUUUGGCCAGUUCCUAUUGUAAAAAAUAGAAUUGGGUUUGGAGGACAAUUUAUGUGACUUUGGGGUUACAAUUACAGCCUUUCUGAUAAAGGACAGAUGGAAACUCAAGGGAACUGGUUAAGUAGGCCUAGGUGGAGAUUUUCCUGGAAAACGAACGAAGUAGAGAAUAGAGCACAGCAGAAAACAGCUGCAUUAUUAAUGGACAGAAAAUGUGAUAGUCCUCUCUGAAGUGAUCCAUAGAGCUUCUCUACCUACACCCUGGGUGUUAGAAGAAAUGAAGAACAAAGACAUGCCUUUUCAGAGGGGAAAGGAAUGGACUAUGACUACUACCUGGCGUCAGUUUGGGUUUCAGCCAUUGACUUGAGCCAAGCGUCACAGGCUGGUCUGUCCUUCCAGUCCCAGCAUUUUAAAAUCCAAAAUAAGGCCACUGUGGUCCAGAAUGUUUAGCCAUUCUAAUCCCUAAUUACAUCAUCCCUCUGUGUUAUGACUAAUUAGUCAGCAAUUGAGCACCAAUCAUUCAACCCAGAUUGCCAUGGGCCUGAUGGAGGGUCCUUCGUUUGGGGUACAAUUUGAAUGCUGGGUUAUAGCUGAAGAUGACCAAAGAUAGAUACCAGCUACAAGUACUUAUCACCCAGAAUCUUUUCUCUUCAGUGGUUUCUAUCUUAAAUAGUCUUCUCUGAAGACUAAUUAGUAUUUGAUAACAAUAAGUGAGAAGGGAGUCUUUGUAGAAGAGACCAUUUUCUUUUUUCUUUUCUUUUUGGAGACAGUUUUGCUCUGUCUCCCAGGCUGGAGUGCAGUGGCACGAUCUCCACUUAAGCAACUGCUGCCUCCCAGGUUCAAGCAAUUCUCCUGACUCAGCCUCCCAAGUAGCUGGGACUACAGGCACAAGCCACCAUGCCCAGCUAAUUUCUUGUAUUUUAGUAGAGACGGGGUUUCACUGUGUUGUCCAGGCUGGUCUCGAACUCCUGAGCUCAGGCAAUCUGCCUGCCUCGGCCUUCCAAAGUGCUACGACUACAGGCAUGAGCCACCAUGCCCGGCCUCAGAAAAGACCAUUUUAAUUUAAAUAUCGGAGUUCAGUUGCAAGAACUUCCCCCCUUUCUGCUGUCAAUUGAAUAUUGUCUGUUCUAAUACUGGGUAAGAACAAUAGAAAAUAAAUAUGAUUGCUUCAUCAAAAAAAUCUGCCAACUCUAUAGAGUGGGAAUACCACAUAGGACCUUAAAAAAUGCUGUCUUCCCUCGUGGACUGACUCAUAGUUAAUACUGGACAACGGUUUUUAUUUUUUUUUAACAUUUAAUAUGAACCAGGGACUGUUCAUACGGUAGAGGAAACUGAGGUUUAGGGAGGUAAAGUAAUUUAGCCAAAGUCAUGAGGCUGCAAAGUGGGGGAGCCAGGAUUCACAUGGAGUGGGGACUGCCUCCAGAGGCCUGGCUCUCAGCUGAUGGGACCCGGCCUUGGUUAUUACUUAGUCUGCUAAUAGCUUAUGUUCUUGAUGGUUUAUCUCUUCCAGUUGCUUAUGCCAGGAGUAUAUCCUUGGAGUUCUAGAAGGAAAUCUGAGAAUAAUGGAAAAUUAAUUGUAAUAUAUUAUUUGAUAUGAGAGAUAUAACUUAUUGCAAUAGCUUGAGGAAGUGUGUUUAACUUAAGAGCGCCCUUUUCUGAAUUGUAGAGGAGAUGAUAGGGAAAAAAAGCAAGACACCAUGUAGGGGACACUUUAGGAAAUAAACAUUUUAAAAUUAUAUCAAACUCAGAAAAAAAGGAGCCACCUACCUGUUAUGGCAGGAAGAUAUGCUGGUGACUUUUUUUUUUUGUAGAAAAGGUGUUGUACUUUUUUUCUUCAUAGGGCCCCUUUUGAAGCCUCAGUGCCCUGUAUUGGCUCUGGUUACUAUCAGCCUGAGAAAUGUUCUCAAAAGCUACGCAGAUGUUUGAAAAUUAGUUCUAUUCUUUAAUGGUCAUUUUUGGAACAUGGUGCAGAUUCUCUUAAAAGUGUGGGUGCCGAUACCCCCUCCACCCCUUUUUGUGAUCACCAUGUGCUCUAUUUAGAUCAUGGAGAUGUGAUGAGUGCUUUGGUUUUAUUUGCCUGUCUCUGAAACAUCACAAGAUAGUAAGGAAGUUCAUGGAUGAGCACAAAUGUCCCUAAUAGAGUGACACACUGUGCUAAGGGAGAUGGAGCAGAUCCAGAUAUCCCUACGGUAUCCGAGAGAGUAGCUUUUCUGCAAAUGGUGGUUGGACAUUAGUUGCUGAAUAGACUCUUCAGCCCCCAAGAAACUAGUGGUGGUUUUAUAAAAUCCUAACAUUGCUAUGGAUCUAUCCAGUUGAUCUCUGGUCUCCAGACAGACCCAUAAUCAAAACCUUCGUAGAAGGAUAAACACAUGUCCUGUUUAUAAAGUGUACUAGAGAAGGCCACAGAGUCAUCCAUUUUUACUUCUCAUCCAUAUCAUUAUCUACCAAAUUUAUAAAAACCGUUAUUUUCUUAGAUAAAGGACUAAAAUAGAAAAAAGGCUUAGAAAAAAUAUAUAAAGUGAACAAUUGAACUGUGUAGUUAAAGAGAGUAAAAUGGAACUGAAGCGUGUUGUUCUCUGGGCAGAAUUUCUAAUUUAGAGGAAUAGGGACUCCAUUCAGCCUUGGACAGCGUAAACUGUGACCCUAGGCAGUAGGGCCUAGCAUUCUAGGAUAAUCCCUCAGAGAGCAGCCUGUCUCAAAGACCAGUUCUCAAUGGGUUUCUUCAGUUUUCCUUUUAAUUCUUUGAGGAAACCUACCCAGGCUACCCUCAGGAACUGCUUUGCAGGAAACAAGGUGAACUGGGUCAACAUAUCUUUGUGGAUACAGUGAGAACUGGGAAUUUGCGAACACAUUCAAUUUGAGGGGCUCCAUAGGAGAGGAAGCUUGGGAUAUGUUCUAAGGAGGUAAACGUAGAAAGUUUAUGUAUGCAGGCCUGGCAAAGGAAUCAUUCAUUCUCUUGAAAAGAAAACCACAUUUUCAAAGACAGAUUCUAUGAUAAUUUAAAAAGUACACUGUAUAGAUCACAUAAAAUAGCACGUAUUUAAGGAGGUGGAAUUGUAUCCUUCCACUUGUGUGGAAGUUUUUGUCAUUCAUUCCAUCUUCUCCCGUGGCUUUGCCUCCAAUUAGCAAUUUUGCAGGCCUGAGAACUGAAGUGGUGUUGAAGAACAGAUGUCAGCUGUUUGUGAAAUUCAUCCCUGCCCCAUGGUUGACUCAGUGUUUCAGAAUACCUCACCCAUUCUUUUCUGACCAGUGGCUGUAGCUUGUUAAUAAUGAAUGAACAUCACCCAUAGGUCCUGAAAUUAACAAGUGUUAAAUGUUAGGUGAUUAUUAGGGGAAAACAAGAUAAUCUAGUCAGUGGGCUUAAUUAGGUGGUGAUUGCCCAAUUGCUGCUUCAUGAUAAUUAUAUUCAUAACCCCAUUUCUAGACAUCAACUACAAUUAUCAAAAUUGACCCCAGCAUAGGUAAGUGUUAGGAAUCUUAUUUGAAGCAGCUUCUCAACGGUAAAUAUCUGAUGUUUCCAAUGUGCUUCUGCCUGUUCUUUCUUCCCCUCUUGCCCCCUUUCCAUGAUCUUUCCCCCAUCUUAGUAGAAAGGUCGUGGCAAUAUUAUUUUGUCUGUGACCAUGCACAUAUUGUAUAGCUUGUGUUGGUGUCUACAGAAAAAGAAAUUCUUAAGUUUUUAGGGGUCAAGUAUAACUGCAAAGCUUUCAUAAAUCAGCAAUAGGAAUCUUGAAGGAUAAAAAUCCCAAAUUGGCUGGAUUGUUAUUUACCUCAGCACAUGAAACCUGUUAAGUCGAUUGAAUAUGAUUCAUUUGAAUAGAUCUUUUACUUUAUAAGGCAUAAUCUUAAAACGAAAAAGAGAGUCAUCUGUGUUUAAGAUAAUGCCUUAGCAACAUGAUCACUAAGAUUUGAGGGAACUGUUAAUCGAGAACUUUUAACUUUAUAUCACCCCUUCCUUUCCUCCAAAUUAUGAAAUUUGCUGCCAGUGUAUUCUAGUAUAAAAAAGAACGUGUCAUUACUAGGGACGUUGUUUACUGUUUAUCUCCCAAAUGAAGUCAAUGAUUUCCAGGAAAUACUAACAACAACCUGUAUCAGAAGUGAUACAGUGUGGGUAUGUCAGUGUGACACUGUGAAUCACUGGGCCAGAUUGUCAUUUGGCAGGCUUCCCUUUCUGACAUGCAGUUAUAUGGGAAAAUAAUGCACUUGAAACUUGCACACCAUGGCUGAACUUCAGAGCAACUAAGAACAACUAGGAACUCAGCUACUGUAUAUAUUGCUUUAUAUGUGUAUAUAUGUAUAUGUAUGUAUAUGUACACACAUGUAUCUCUAUACAUAGAGAAAGAUAGAUAGAUAGAUACUCUCUAGGCACUUAUUUUUCUCUAAAACAUCAAGAGUGCAAAUAGUCAUCUCUUAGAAUUUCUGGGGUGAAAAUGCAGUUCUCUGUGCAGGGGUCUCUGUUAAGAAAGUGAUGUGUAGUAGGUGGAAUAUACUCUUUGGGGCCACACAAGCUGAGGCUGAAAUUUGUCUCUGUCCAUUACUAGCUGUGGGACCUUGAGUAAGUCAUUUAUCCUUUCUGUCCCCAUGAUUUCCUACCCAGUAAAAUAGAAAUUAUUAUAAUUUGAAUCUGUAGAACUAACAUAAGGAUUAAAAAAUAAUAUGUGUCUAAGAGUCCUGGCUCAUAAUGGCCAGGAAGGAAGAAAGUGAUAGUUUCUUCCUUCCUCACUGAUAGAGAAACUGAGGCAGAGAUCUUCUCCAGGGCUUUGCCCCAUUUAUCUAUGGUCAGUAUAUUAGGUAUUUUGUUCUUGGUCUUAAAGUCAGCUUUUGGAAUCCUGCUUGUUUAAUUUUGUGCUGUGUGUCCCUUUACUGAUGAGUAGUCUUUGCUGCAGUUGUCCAUUCCCAGCUAGACUUUAUUACAUCUUCAACUGAUGUUCUGUGGAUGAAGCAGCACUCUGUAUUGCUGUGUGUGCAUUCAGUAGGAGCUUGUAAACUACCCGAGAAUGAUGCCAUUUCCUCUUGGAAAAAGUACAUUUAUAUGGUAACAACGCCUUCAACCUGACCUUGCAGAGCUAUUCCCUGGAGUGUUGUAGGGGAACAAUUUUUAAUAAACAUGAAGUUUUCUGAGCUUUUCAGAAGAAAGAUGUUAUUACUGUUCCUAUUGUUUGGCAUCAUUCUGGCAAAAAUGAUAUGUCGAAGAAAAUUGUCCUUAUUGCAGAGAAAAUAUUGGCUGUGCUGUUUAUAUAAAUGUUGUCUGCCUCACUGUUGCUCUACUCACAUACAUAUCUCUUAGCCAGUUUGAGGACUGCCCCAUAGCCUGGCUUAGAAAUGCUUUGGUUUUCUCUGUGCAAAUGUUUAUUUCAAUAGUCCACAUCUACUUGGUCUUACUAAUGUACUAUAAUAUCAGAUGCUUUGAGACCUCACGGGUAAGGAGACUAAUUUUAGAGUGUUUUAAGGGUAGAUGAUAUUUUAAAAUGUAGAAAACGUGGAAUGGUGUUGGUAGGGCCUAACCAGACUUACCUUAUUGGGUCUGGCCAAAAGGACAUUCAUUGGUAGCUUUAUUGGUGGUGGUGGUGGUGUGGUGGUGGUGGUGUGAAUGUUAGUGGGAAAGAUGAAGAACAUGUAAGUGGUUCUUUGGUAAAACCAUAUAGUGAUUUUUCACCUGUACAAGCAAACUACUCAUGAUUUUUUUUUUUUUUUUUUUUUUUUUUACAUUUGGGAAAUUUCCAGAGAAAUAAAUAUGUCAUUGGAAUGUUGUUGUUAUUAUUAUUAUUAUCAUUAUUAUUACUAUUUUUGAGAUAAGAUCUUGCGCUGUUGCCCAGGCUGGAGUGCAGUGGCAUGAUCUCAAGCACACUGUAAGCCCGGCCUCCUGGGUUCAAGUGAUUCCUCCACCUCAGCCUCCCGAGUAGCUGGGACUACAGGCAUGCACCACCAUGCCUGGCUAAUUUUUAGUAGAGAUGGGGUUUCAGCAUGUUGGCCACGCUGGUCUUGAACAGGAGUUCAAGUGAUCUGCCCACCUCGGCCUCCCAAAGUGUUGGGCUUGCAGGUGUAAGCCACUGCGUCCAGCCAGAAUGUUACUAUUUUUUAAUUAUAAAUAAACUUUAGAGUUGCCACUCUAACUUUGUCCAGAGCUAUUUGAGGAGGAAAGAAAAACCUUGUGUUUAUUUACUGGUGUUCAAAUCUCUAGGAUUCUCCUAAAUGAGAGAUUUUUGGUCUUCAAAGGGUAGAACUCAAAACUAAAGGAGUAGAGAUGUAGCUGUGGCUGUGGCAGUGGUUAUUAGUACAGAAUGCCCUCAAUACAGUAAGAAAUAUGGGAUGAAAGAGUAGGAGCUGAACCCCAGACUCCCUAGGACCCCUAAAAGACUGGGAGUGGGAAGGUUGUCCAGUUGUUUACUUCCUUAAGAGAUGUAUUUGGGAAUGCUACUGUCACAUGUGUUCAGUUCGUGACAUGUAGGAUCCUUGCUUAUUUGUGACUACAGAGUAGUGGGAAAGUGAUUGGCUGUGGGGUAUGACCUGAAUUCACUCCCCUGCCUGCCACUUCCUAGCUUUGUGAACCUGGGUCAAGCUCAUAAUGCUCCUCUGCUCCAGUUUCUUAUCUUUAAAGUGGAAUUCUCUUUCUGGUGAAGCCUGAGAGGCAUAAUGUAUGUAAAGCAUUCAGCACCCUGCCAGGGGCCCAAUAAAUGGCCAUCUCUACCGUUCAUUUGCAAUGAUCAAUUAGGGGCCACCCAAUGCCUCUGGUACAGAUGGCAUGCUCUUGCCAUUCAUCCAAUGCCUGGUUUUGCAUGCUUAGUUAGCAGUUGUGGGAUGAUAGAGUUGGAAAUAAUUUAGUGUCUUCAUGUGUUUUAUAGAAGCUGUUUAUUUAAGGAAUAUGUGCCCAUACGUCUAUUCAUUCAUUGAACACUUACUGAGCUCCUCCUUUUGAGUGAGUACUAAGCACGGCUACAGUAUGCCUAGGUGGUCAAACCCAGGGGAUAUGAGAUCUCUCUAUCACAGUUGUGUUAGGCUCUUUGUUUUGGUAAUUGAGUGAUUAUGAUGGAGAUAGGUGUCCUCAGCCACAUUCAAAUAGCCUGGAGCCAGGGGAUGGUGAAGAGUGGCUUAGGCUGUGGGUAGUGGAUUCCUGUUUAGAUGCAUUCAUUUCUACGUCUUUGUGUGUAUAUAUUUACAAUAUAAUCUGCUAACCAUAUAGUCAGUGCUGCUGUGGUUCGUAAUCUGGCAGAUGAUUUAAAUAUUUACUCCAAAAUAUCUUGUUCUCUGUUGGUGUGAAGUAGAGUUUCCAGUUAUUUUUAGGUCAUUUUCAUCUUAGCAACCCUGUUGGAGAUGAACCAGACAUGCUGCUGUAAACUGUCCCCACAUUUGGAUAGAAUUUAAUAAAGUAAAGUUUAAUGGUUUGGUCCCAAGAGGCAAACAGACCAUCUGGUUAGCAGAAGGUUAGGUCAAGUAUUGCAUGGCUGCUGAGAGGGCCACAAACCAGCCCUGACGCACUGGUAAUGUGUCCAGUUGCUGAAUGCAUUAAGCAUUGAAAUGGUGCUUUCAGGUCUGCCGAGCCAGCAGUUCUGUUACCACCGCUGUGACGCAGGAGAUAAUUCAGCUGGGCAAGCAGCAGCAUGGGGGUGGAUCUACAGUACAGGAUGUGUAAUGUCAACAUGAAGGAUUGGAGCUGGCAGAAGGAAGGGAAGCAGUCAUUUCAUGCCAGUGCAGGAAGCCUAGAGAGAUGCUUUCCACCCCCCCCCCCACCCCCCACCUUGUCUCUUGUCCUCUUCUGGAGCUUUCACAUUAUGUGUUAAAUGAUUACCUUGUGCAUGGUCCAUGGCAAAACUUCAGCUGAUUUUUCUGCCUCUUUUGGAACCUGUCAGCAUAAACAGAGUAAACCACAUUCCACACACAUGUAGGGCGGGCAAAGGAAAGAGUUUACUGCACAGACUGGGAGGAGGAGAAAGGGCUUCAUUAGGCAGGAGCAUCUUUGUGCUUGAGAUGGAAUCCCAUUGUAUGUCCCUUUGUGCUCAGAUUUGAGACCGGCCAUCCAUUCAAAGCCUGCAAUCAUCUCGGAACAUUGUGCUGCAGCUGUAGUUGGUAGAAGCCUGCAGAAUGGUUCCAGUGAUUCUGCAGAAGCUUAGCAAUUAUAUAAUUGCUAUGUAACUGGAGAGAGCCAUCAGGAUUGUCUAGUUCCCCUGGAAAGAAAGCUUCUACAAUUUGAGGGGUAGAUUGUUUUCCCUUGUUAAACCUGAAAGCUGAUGAGCAAGUACAUCAUACCACUAGGCUGAAACCAGGUCCUCUCACUGGCAUGAGAGGGGAAGAAAUUCACAAGUACACUUGGCUGGAUAUUCAGUGGACUUCACAGCUGUGUUAAAGGGAGAGAGAGCAACUCACUGACUCUUGGAAUCGUGGAUCCUUGUAGCAGUUGAACAUGAUAGUUGAAUUGUUUCUAAUAUCUGAGACUGUGUUCUAUAUGCAUUCAAGGCAUGGAGUAUUCCAGAGCUUUCCUAGGAAUGGGACAAACAGAGUUGCUCGUAACCACCAAGAGCCCUCUCAAUUUCUGCCGCCCGCUCAGGAGGAUUUUCACAGCCUCUCUUGAAUGAAUACUUGCCUCAGAUGCUGAUCAGUGGAAGCACUGCAAAGCCUGACUCUUCAGAUAUUCCCGAAUGCUGAAAUCUUCUCUGCAUCAGCUCAUGAUUCUGUCUGGGCCUGUGCAGUCCAGGAGCUGGGACAGACUGAACAGUUUGCCUGUGAGAACUUAACAGUGCAGAAAUGAAUUCCUUCUUUCAGCUACCUUACCACUUGUUUUCCAUAGUUGAGAAAACUUUGAAGUGGUGUUGGCUAAAUGUAGGUACGAGGGCUGCAUUAAACCAGUGAGAAGUCCAAGGCUCCAUUUCAUCCCGUGUAAAACACUCAUCUAAAAUUAGCCACAUCUCCUAACCCAAGUGUGGACUUUGUGUUUGUUUAUGUUAAGUAGCUCUAAAUUUCAGUGAUCCUGCCUUUCUGGUGUCAGUUUUGUGGAGCUGCUAGAAUAGAAAGAGUGGUUGUUGGGAUAUAUUUUUAUUAAUGGUUUAAGUUGGGCCUUUUAUAACUGAUACUCACCUAUAUUUCUCUAUUUAAAUGUGUUUGUAGUCAGAACUUCAGUAUAAGGGAAAAGUAAAACAUUUUGGUUCCUUUGUGAAUUAAAAAGGAAUGUCUAGUAGGCAGUGUGGGGACCUGGACUCCCAAGAUGGAUUGGGUCCACACAUUCCUAGACCUUUGACCUUUAUACCUGUACGUUACUCUGUACCUCGUGGGUUUAACUCUGAGGUUGAUAGAUACAAAUAGUUUCUUUAAGAAUUCUGAUUCCUACAAAACAAUAUUGGCAGGUUUUCAAGGAGCCAGCCUGUCUCAGCACUGAGCUUUUAUUUUGUAACAAUUUGGAGGGGUAUAGGAUCACCCAUGGUGACCCUUUCCUGCGUCAUUCCAGGCAGGCCUUGGCAUGCUUCGCCAGAUGAGUAAGGACGAGGACAGUUGGCAGGAGGACCUGCUGAGUUCAUCUUGCUUCGUAUCUUAGGAACUGGCUUGACCCUGCUCCAUCAUCAGUGUUUGGGCCCUCUGAGAAACUCUAGACCAUCUUUUCAAACACUAGGCUUGGAGAUUAUUAUGUUGGGAGCAGCAGCGUGCCCUCAUAUGAGGGAGGAGCACUUGAUUCUAGCGCAGAGGACACAUCGAAGGGGGACCCUUUUCUGUCAGUAUUGGUAGGCCUGUGAGGACCUUGGUGGUGAGGGCCAUGGUGUAUAGUGGAAAGAUCGUAGACCUCAGAGUCAGUGAGUAACUGGGUGACCUUGAGGGAAUGAUUUAAUCUUUGGUCCCCAAUUUCCCUAUCUGGAAAAAAAAUCCACUUUGUAAAGUUCUUUUGAGGAAUAAAGGAAAUCAUGAAAAGAAAUCUCUGGUGCAGAGCUUGACAUAUAGUAGACACACAAAAAAUCCUAAUUUUCUUUCCUCCCAUCUUUGAGUUUGUAUUAAACACUUUCUAUAGGUAGAGCACUGUUAAACAGUGACUAUCUGAUUAGAAGUCAGAAUAUACCUGAGUUUUACAUGAAAUCCCAAUUGAGGGCUCCUUGAAGCUUGUACUGGUAAAAUUGACAAACAUAUACCUUCUUGGCUAAAGAGGCUGAGCAAUAUUUUUUAUUAUAUGGUGGCUUUUCAAAGCCAGUGUGCUCCCCUAUGAAACAUGACUCCAAAAUCUGGUAAAAGGGAAGCAAAGUACCUUACCCUCUGUUUGUGCUAUCUUGAACAUUCUAUAAUAGAUUAUAUAUUAAAUUCCUUAGAUGAAGUUCUGGUUUUUUGUUUUGACUAUUGCUACACGACUAACUCCUCUAUAGUAAACCUGAAAUUUUCCAGGAAUAGCACAGAUGUAAGCUAUUUGAUUAUCUAGAAUCCAAAUGUCUUAACAGUUUUAAUGUCUUACAAGCCUUUUUUCUAUCACCUCUAGUCCAGUGUGCAACUCUUCAUGUUGGUGUGCAGGCAGCCUUAUUGACUGGUUUCAGGGAAAAAGAUCUUAUUCAGUUAAAAUUUAGCUGAUCAACUUUGAAGGCCAACCACUGAUUUGUUUCAUAAUGAGUUCCUGAACAGGACUAGACUAGAAGCUACAGAAAGGCAGGCUGAGUCUCCCUUGCUCACUAGUGCCUUGAGCAAUGCCUAAAACAGAUGUACACAGUCAAAAUGUAUGGAGUCUGUAAACCAAACCUAGCAUUUUUAAAAAUGUCAUAUUGCUCCUAAAUAUCUGUUCCUUAAAAGUGCCUACAUAUCUGAAACAGAAUAGUCUCUUAGUUGCUUCUGAGCAGUCAUUUCUGCCUGAAACAUCGCUAGAUUUAUAGCAUUCAAUUAAAAAAUGAAAGUUAAUGUAAGUUCUCAAUCAAAGAAAACUACCCAUCUCUACAAUCCAUAUUAUGUACAUUUUGAAGUAAGAAUGUCUAACAGUCUAGGUUAAAGAAGCCAAGGAAAAUUUGUUUGUCGGUAGCUUUUGAAAGAUACUAAUGUGAGGAUGACAUUUGACUAGUAUGAUCCUGAAUGAUCUUCAGUGCAUUAUAGAGUUAAAUUUCAUAGAAUUGAGUCUGAAACAUUGGAUAAGAAAAAUUCAAACUCGAAUAUUCAGUGAUUCAAGGCCAUUGGUUCUGGAGGAAACUCAUUUGCGGUUUUAUGUGAAAGAGGAAGACAGGUCUUUUUCCAAGACUUUCUUUGACCUAUUAAGUCUAAAUGGAUGGUGGCAUGUAUUUUGUAGGGUAAAUUGGUGGUAUGGAAGCCUCAAGGAAUAUAGGGAAAAACGUUAUGGAAAAAAAUGAUGAGUAUGUAGUGUUUCCUAUCAAUUUAACAAAAUUGGAAGGAUGAAGCAACGGAACCAGGAUGAUAGUCAUGUUCUUUGAAGAUGGUCAAGCAGAUUCAGAAAACAUCCUUCUUCACCUUUGACUUUAGUUCUUGAACAUUUCAAUGGAAUGAUUUAGAUCAUUGAAAGUCUACUAUGUGCAGAAGCCUUCUAGGUAUUAGGUGACCUUGCAGUAUUAAAGAAACCCAUGGGUCCUGUUAGUCCCAACCUCACUGAAGGACAUAUUCUGAAGAGCCAGCUCAUUAAGCAAGCUUUUGAAGGGUGUGCGCUGCAGAGCAGUUUCCUGUUAUUUGGUUAAUGGUUGACCUAGUUCUAAUGCCAUAUGCUUCCUGGAACGCAUUCUAAUAUAAAGUAUGUGUUAAAGCAAGACUAGGAUAAUAGCGGGAAAGUCAAAGCCUUUCUAAAGCAGAGACCAUAUUAAUGCUGGCCCAGUGAAGGCAGAAUAGUGUGCGGAUGGAAAAUGAAAAGACUUUUCUCCUCAUGAUCCUGUUUGGUAAUUCUGAUUUUAAUCCUCACAUUUUAUCCCAGUUCAUUCUAAGGAGUUGCAUUUUCCCCAGAAUACCGUAUACAUAAGGCCUGCGUCAUUAGUUCAUUUUUCAGUGAAUGCUAGGCCAAGGUUAGUGUUGAAGUACCCUAAGUAAAAUUAUUACUGCAAGGAAAGAUUAGAUUAGAGUUGGCUAAUGGCAGGUGAUUUUGUUUUUGUGUUAUUAUUUUUGUAUUGUAAACAGGGGAUUAGUAAAUCUUUUCCUCUGAAGUUUGGAUGCGGUUCAAAGCUAAGAUUGAGGCUCCUUUGGCUUAUUUAUCCUUCUACCUGGAAUCAGCAGCCCUGGCUUGUUCAUUUAGAUGGACAGGGGAGCCUACGCAAGUCAUGGGGGCUGGUGAGCAAACUCUACACCAGGCACACAAGUGUUUGUUUUAACAGCUUCAGAAUGUGAAGAAUCUGUAGGUCUAGUCUGCUAAUUGCUGGAUAUUUGGGUGGCAAUAGAGGAAGCUGUUAUGCUGUCUUCAUUGCUCAUAAAAAAAUGUUUAAGCAACCACAAGUGUGUAUAUAUGGUGGGGGAAGGGUGGACAGCUCCCUUUUAAAAAGUUUUCUUUCUAAAUCACCAUAAACUUGUGGUAUGCAGCAGUGAUUCCUAAACCAGGCUGAUCUUCAGAAUUAUUCUGAGAACUUAGAAACAAAAAGGGAUUUAUUAAAAAUAGACUUUCAGGUUCUACCACAGGAGAGGAAUUCAUUAGGUCUAGGGUAGGAGCCUAGAAUGUUUAUUCUUAGAAGCCAGGUUUGGGAGCCACUGGUCUUGGUAUCAUUAAGGAAGGGAGGAAGAAGCAGCCACUGUGCUUGAAGAGUUGACAUGCAGGAAGUAGGAAAAGGAAAAGAGUUGCUGUCAGAACUUGAUAUUUGUGGCUGCUAAUAAUUUGAGCUAUGGAAUAGGCUUUCGUCUUUUCUUCUCUAGGAAUUUAGUACCUUCAGAGCACCUUAAGGGUACUGUAUACUGAGUGAUUUACUCACUACUGUGGUUACUGGAUACUGAGUGAUUUAGGUUUGGGAAAUGUCAUCUCGGUGACAGGCUACAUACUGCAACCACCACCAUCCACCUCUGCCCUGUCCCCUUCCUCCCACCAUGGAGGCAGUGGAAACAGAAUAUCUGUCAUUCAUCAGUUAAAUUGGAUGCAAUUUUUUCAUAUUAAUAUAUUUGGCAGAAACAAAGGAAACACAUUAUGUUGAUUUCUGUAUACAAAGAAAUUGCUGUGAAUUCACCCAAGUACAUUUUUGGUUUUUUUGUUUGUUUGUUUGUUUUUUCUAUUGACAAUAAGAGAUGCACUUGUUGACCGAGGACUUGUUCCAUAUGGCUUCCUGCCUGGCCUGGUUUGAAGCUGUUGCUUCUGAUAUUGGGCCACUGCUAACUGACCUAGUUGUAAAUUAGAGUAACGUUGGCUAGAGGAUCAACACGGUCUAGGGUCUAAUAGUAUGCCUGAUGUGUAGUUGAUCAUCAAUGCUUAUUAGUGAAUGACUGAGCCAGCUCAGUAGAUGUUUCUUCAAAAGAUAAGAAGUAACUUGGAGAGGUUAAGAUUCUGCUUCAAAGCAAUGUAUGUGUUCAACAUAACCUUUCUAGAGAGAUUUCUGCUUUAAUCUCAAUAAAAAGGAAAAUGGCCCUGUUGCAAAAUUUGGCAGGUCAGACACUUCAGCUUCCCAAGAAAAUGCAAGGAAUUUAUUUAUUUUCUUUACAUGUUGUCUACUCCUAAAACAACUAUCACUACUACCAUUAAACUCUCCAUAUACAUUAAAGGAAGUGCCUCUAGAAUAAAUGUUGUUAAGAGAAUUUAAUCUUCACUUUCCUUCUAACUUUAAGAGCCUCAUGGGAAUGAAAAGAAUGUUGUUUUAGAAGUAGAAGAGAAGAAACAAUUGAGUAGAAAAAGAAAAUAAUUUGAGAAAACUUGUCUGGUUGACAGUAAUUUUUUAGUAACAGAAAGCAGCAGUCAUGGCCCAAGAACCUGUGGUUCUUGGUUGUGUCCUUGCCAUGCUUAGAAGGUUCAAGAAAGGGAGUAUAGUCUCUUUAAAGUUAUUUUGAGGAGUUGGACACUACCUACUAGGUUCCUAAUGCUUACCCAAGUUAAGAGGUUGAAGUGCCUCCAAGACUUUAAGUAGCAGCUGAACAUGUGAUCUUGUUAACCCUGAGAUGUUGCUGAAAAGUGACUCAGAUCACCGUGGCAAACAAUCCUGUCCAGUUCCAGCUGCCCCAGCAGAACUCAGCAUUAGGUCACCCUUUAGGCGUAUGGUGCAGAGCUCAUGCUACCAUCAAGACUUUAGAACAAGGACAACUUGAAGUGGCUAUCUUGCACAUGGGACUGAUGUUGAGGACUGCUUGAUGUUUUGGAGCCCACCUGAUUCUUAAGAGUUUCCAGUUCCUCUAUCCCUAUUCCCUGUCAUCACAUAAACCACUUGGAGAGAAGGGGAGGAUGCCAGAGAGAGUCAUGUUCUGAUAAUUAUUUGCUCUUUGGAUAUUUCCUCAUCUAGAUAGACGGGACUUUUUGUUUUCCCCAGGAAAAGGUAACGUAUGCUCAAGGUAGCCUUAAAAAAAUGUGUGAUGCCUAUUUUAAAUAAAAUAACAAACUAGAACAGUUUGUAUUUUAUUAAAUAAUAAUCAAGAGGUAACUCAUACCCAAGAAGUGGGUUUGUUGGCCUUAGCCUGAUAGGUGGUAGCCACAUAAUGACUCAUUGAGCACUACUGACUUAGUAAAAAAGAAAAGUAGGGGUGGGGUGGUUAAGAAGGUGGCUGGGAUUGUUACCUCACUGGACCGCUCUUUAAACUUUCUCUGUCUUUUCAUGACUUGGGUAUGUUUAUGUAGAUCCAAAAUUAUUUUAAAGUUUGAAGUGUCUUUCUGUUAGCUGUGUGAAUGUGCUGCCUAUUUCGAAAGUUGAUAAUGACUCAAGGGUAUCCAACUCUCAGGAUUCAAGCCACUGCAUGUUGGCAAUGUAGUAGAUCCUGGUUUUAAAAAUAAAAUGCCAGGAUGCCACCCUGAGGAUCCAGACAUAGGCUGUGAGCACAUUUGAAAUCCACAUCCUCAAAUAUACAACAAUGUCAGCUACAAAAAAAAUAGAAGAGAUAGGGUCUGAAAAGGAAGGAGCUCCUGUCAUCCGCAGUCAAUGUGAAGAAACUGGUUAUAUGGACCUAGGAAAUCAUCCCACUUAACCCCUUCAUUUUACAGCUCUGGAAAGGCUGAAAUGAUGUGUCCAAAGUCCACAAUGUAGGAAGUUAGUUAAGGAAGCCUGAAAUGGAAUAUCAGUUUUCUGCCCUGGUGAUCCAUGCUUAUUCCACUACAACAGUGUUGGCAGAUAGCUUCUAUUUCUCGUGCCAAUUUUGAUUGAUUGGUGGAGAAUGCCUGGAGCUUCACUUUGAGGAUUCUGUGCCUUGUCUAGGCUUGUUGGAAAAGAGUGUGGAGAUCAAGCAGAGAAGUCUGCAAUAGGCGGGAGAGGGUAAAUGACAGGCGGUGGCACUUCCCUAUACUUGCUGUCCCUUACAAUUAUGUGACUUAAAAUUACAGCCUUACUCUUUACCAAAACACUUUCUCCCUUGGUGUUCAUGAAGACAUCCUAUUUCCAAAUGUUUUCAAACAAAAAAGAGAAUAUUUAGUCAAGGGCAGAGAAUCUCAUUCAGAAUAGCUUGUCCAGGUGAUUUAUCCAGGGUAACUAAGUUGUUGAGUAGCAGUUUGAACGAAUGAUAAGGUUUUCACCAUAAGUUUUAUAACCUAUCAUGAAGAGCUGUCUUUCUGCAUUGUUGGUAUUGUCUAACCCUGAUAAGGCUGAGGAGUCAUUCAUCUGUUUCACCACCACCUUCUAACAUGUUGUUCUUACAUGUUAUCCACAGCUGGCUUUUCCUUGCCUACAUCCUCCUAGGCCAUCUACUAAAUCCUCUCCCUCCGUAAAUGGAAGUAUAAAAACAGUUUCACAAAGGUCAUAAUUUGCCCAGGAUAAUACAGAGCCCAACUGGAACCUUGGUUCCCUGACCAUCAGUAUUCCAAGAUACUUCCUGACAGGUUUCCUACUUAUUACAAUAAAACUAGAAGGAACCUUUGAGGUUAUUUUUUUAAUGUUAUCUUAUAGCCAGAGAAGUCGAAUCCAAGAAUAUUUAAGGGACUUGCUCAAGGUAACGAAGUUGUUUAGUAGCACAAACACCCUCUGGAUCUUGAAAGCUAAACCCACAUUGUAUAUACAUCUAUUUCUUUCCUUUCUCUCCUUUACUUUAAUGAGACAAAUGAACUGUUUAUUGUUGAAUUCACAGGGGUCAUGAUUGCGUUGCAACAUACUAGAAUCUCUAGAUUUCAAAUAGAAUGAUGAAACUGUGAUUAAAAAGGACUUUUUGGGUUAUCGUUACAUAGUUUAUGUAGUACAUUUAGAAAGAAAGACUGAUAAUAAAUUUUCUCGUAACACGACCCUCACAAGUGUAAUUUUGGAACCCUUUCUACUUCCAAAGACAAGCUGUUGUGAAGAUGAAUGUGGGAGAUAAAUGUGCCUGGCAGUCUAAAGCAUGCCAUGAAUUCGUGGUUGUCUAGCCCAGUGCUAGGUACAUGAUAGCUGUUCUGUAAAUGUGGAUUUUUUUUUUUUUUUUUUGAGACGGAGUCUCCCUCUGUCGCUCAGGCUGGAGUGCAGUGGCGCGAUCUCGGCUCACUGCAAGCUCCGCCUCCCGGGUUCACGCCGUUCUCCCGCCUCAGCCUCCCCAGUAGCUGGGACUACAGGCGCCCGCCACCGCGCCCGGCUAAUUUUUUGUAUUUUUAGUAGAGACAGGGUUUCACCGUGUUAGCCAGGAUGGUCUCGAUCUCCUGACCUCGUGAUCCGCCCACCUCGGCCUCCCAAAGUGCUGGGAUUACAGGCGUGAGCCACCGCGCCCGGCCAAAUGUGGAUUUAGAUCUACCACCAGAGCUCUGUCAUGGUUAUCUUUUUAUGUACGAACUGACAAUACUUUGCCCUGAAUAGGGUUAGUGUUUGGCAGGGAGGAAGCUAUGUUUCACUGGUAGAGCAGUCUGUUAACGUCUAAUUUGAGAUGAAUGCUAUUGAUAACAGCAUAGAAAAAGCUACUGUCAUUUCCAAUUCAGUUGCAUCCAUUUGCCCAUCUUGGCCAGUUUGGAAAACAUAACUGGGGCUCUUUUUUGGCGUCUUCAGUAUCAGAUAGCUCCGUAUAUGCAGUGCCACUGUGGUCUGUUGCCAUUGGCUACUCCACAUCUGUCACUCUUCCCACCGUAUUAGCUAAUAAUGAGAGAGAGUUAACCUAGAUUUCUAAGAUCCUGGUGUUCAAAAGUGUUGACUCUUGGACCUCUUGAGGAAGUAGGCAAGGUGGGCCACCUUGGAGCUUUUAUCCUCUGCUGGAAUAUUUCCUUUUGAAGUGCCACCAUUUAUAGAAUCAUCAAUUACAAACCUUUCCCAUGUUCCUUCUGGAACCUCAAUCUAACCUUGAGCCUUUGUUUUUGGAAGAUAAUGGUACAAUUUCUACACAAAACUGGGAACAAACUACUUUUAAUUCCUUUUCCUCUUAGUUGUUUCAGCAGAAUGAUCCCCUUUCACUUUAACAGAAAGAUUCUCUUUCUAGCUUAAAAUAUUCUGGAUAUGCUUUAACUUGCCUUGGGGUCAUAGCACACAUCUCCCAGGACUGAUGAGUCUUGUCAGUUGCCCCAGGGUGAGAACUUUAAUAAGCAAAUUGCACACACCUGGUUUUGCAAAAUAUUGGCCUAAUGGGGCACCUAGGUGGAAGUCAGUAAGUAUGUCCACUCCCUAUGUACACACCCUUCCUCCCCACCCCUUUUAAAAGGGAGGCCUCAGAAAUGCUACCUCCCCAUUUAUCUUGUAAAACUUUCCUGUCUCUCCUUCGCUGUGCUCGGGUAGCUCAGAGGGUUGUGAUCGUUAACGAGCUCAGGGUGUUACUGUCACUGCUGCUGUCUUGUGGAUUUGAAAGUAAUGCCGUGAUGGGAUGUGGUAUAGGUACGGGGGAGUCUGGUUAAAAGGGAACAGGGCUGGAGAACUCUCUUUGUCAGACUGUGAUUCCCCCUGCUCUGCUCUUUGAUUUGUGGCUGCCAUUGGUGUUUACACAGCCUUUCCCCGCUCACACUUUCCUUGGUUAGUUGAAAAGAAACAGCCUGUUUUCCUGUUACUGAAUGCUGGACCGUGGGCUUACUUGUUUUUUACUCUUUUUCAUUCAUUUGUUCAUUCAUUUAAAUACUUACUGAGCAUUUGACUGCUUCCCAGGCUUUGUGCUAAAUGUUGGCUCUACAGAAAUGAAAGACCUAGACCCUGCCUUUCAGAGGCUCAUAAUCUAGUAUUUACAUCUCCAGUUGUCAACAGGUCUAACACAUUACCACCACCACUAGAAGUGGUGCGUUUUAAUGCAUUUUAUUUGGCUUAUGUACUAUCUUUAUUUGCUGACGAUCAACUCCCCCAAAUAAAGCUAUUUGGAUAUCUUUCUUGUUAUCCAUUCUUUCAGACAUAUUGGCUUACCCAGGUGAUUAGAGUGCAGGGUAACUGCCUUAAGAAGCUACAGUGGCAUUGAUACUUACACAUAUCCAGGCCAACUAAUAGGUGUGACCAUUUCUUUGUUUUAUGCUCUAGUGUAGAGCUUGACUCCACCUUACUUUCCGGCUGCCAUCCAGUUAACAUACCCACAGGAUUCUUAGACUAGGCAUACAUCAUUGUAUAUAUUCUGCCUAAAAGUUUGUAAAAUCUAGUGGUGGCAUUUAGCUCUUUUGGCAAUAAAAACUAUAUGUGAGAAUUUCGUGGCCUUGACUGAGCUGUGUAUGGCCUCACUCUUCAAUUCUGUUGUCAGCCUAUGUUCCACAAUCAUUUGUGUGUGUGGACCUCAAGAAUUUCAGUCAACCCGGCAACACAUGCAGUGCCCCUUCCGGGAACACUGGUGAUCUUCUGGUCUCUUGGUUUGGAGUUAAUUAAACAUUGUCGGGAGAAUUCCUUCAUUUCCUUCUGGAGUCCUUUUUGGGCAUACAAAAAUCUAGCACUUGAAGCCACUUAAUCAAAUAUCAUAUCCACACACCUGCAGUUCUUUCUCUGUGUCCACAAACAUGGUUUUACACUUGGAUGAUGUAGUUAGGCUCAACUCCAUUUGUAGUGAGAAACAUUUGAAGCUUGUCCCCACUCAACAAUGAUGAUGCACUUAGGCUUACCUUCGUAAUAUGGGUAAAUGUCUCAGGUUAGCCAAAUGUACCUAGGGUCAGAGGGCAUAUGCUCUGAUAUGGAAUUUUGGAGGUCAUUCCCUGCCUUUGUCCUCUGCUCUAAGGCUCAUGUCACUCGCAUCAUGCUGUGACAUGAAACAAUAUUGCAUCGUAGGGAGUGCAUAGUAGACUAUGUUGUUCAAUUAUCAUGAGAUUACCACAUACUCUUGCCUGGAAUCUUGCCAGCAAUAGUGAACAAAGAGAUGACCCAAGCAACUUUCUCACUUUUAUUCUUGAAGACUAAAUGGCAUCCUUAAAAUCUGAUGGUUUUCUUUGUACCUUUCUGGUUGAGUAAAGAAUAAGAUAGUCUUUUUCUUUUUUGGAAAAAUCGUAUGGCUAGUACAGGAAAUCAAGGAGAUUUUUAGCUAAUUUAGUAAAAAAGUCAGAGGUGGAACAGAAAAUACACCGGCUGAAAAAGGAGAUGAUUGAUUUCUAGGAAAUGGGAGAUUGUUUGGUAUAUUUACAGUAAUGAAGAAGAGUUCUUCCUGGAACAAAAGUACUGAAUAAAUAACAACAAGAGACAAAAAAGAAAAAUGCAUUUCCCUGGUACACAAACCUUGAAGCUCAUGCUUUUUGCCAUUAGGAAUUCUGAACAUGUCUUGAAUUCUUAGACUUUCUUGAUUUUUAAAAUCUAAUAUUUAAUUCCAAAAUAAUUUUUAUUCAUGUCUGCGUUUUCUUUGUUUUCCCCCUGAGUUAUCUGUGUCCUCUGAAAGUUUAAAAACAAGUGAUUUUUUUUUCUCAUCUUGUUGGCGGAGACAUACAAUAGGCUGCCUCUCCCCUUCUCUGUGGAAAGAAUGGAAACAUAGUAAGUGGCCAGAGGAGCUCCAUACGGAUUGACAUUCCUUGCUUCUGCUUUUGAAGUUAAGAUGGUCACGAGAGAGAAAAAUAUUUUUGGUUCCAAGCCUAAGAAAAGGACAUUCCUUUUAGUCUUGGCAUUCUUGUUUUCAUGGUGUUGAUUUCUCUUUGAAUUAUCAUUAGUACCAUUAAUAAAUCACAUCUGAACGUGAAAUCACUUUUGCAAGUUCUUCCCCUCUCCACACCCUUGAUUAUAGAAAAGGUGACGUUUCUUGAUAUUUAUCUGAAGUAGCUUAGAGUAUGUUUUCCUGGCUUUUUGUUCCCCCCUCUGGAUGGGUUCCCAUUGUUGAUCAAGCAUAUUCAAGAGAGUUUUUUCCCAAGAGUCCUGAGAGACCCAUCCAUGCAUUCUAUUCUGUUAAACAAGGAAAAUAAUAAUAAUAAUGUUUAGCUUUCACCUUGCUUUAGAGAGAGAAAUCUCAGAAGAACCAUUUUCCUUUCAGGAGGAUUGGGGUUCUUAGGUUAAAUUCCAUAUUAUACAAAUUCCCUAAUGACAAAUAACCUAUGCAAUCAACAAUCUUUCUUUUAAAUGUAUUUCUCUAUUGAAAGAGCAGGGGAUUCCAUUUGAGGCUGUUGAUUAAGACAUGAAGACUAGGUCUAAAAUUGGUGGUGGCCCAAGGUCAUUGGUAGAACUAAUGGACCAUUUGAAAAUUAUUAGCAGCUGGUUUAAUAGAGUUUUAAUAACUACAGCUGUGAGAAAAUCCAAGUACAAGGUAUUUGGAAUGUUCCCUCUGAGGUCCUUUCCUUUUGUUCUAUAAUAAUCCUGGCAUCCAUUUAACGAAAGUGCAACUCAGAAGAUUAGGUAGCUAUAUACGUAAGCAUAUCAUGCAGGCUUUAUUUGCUUUAGGUUUUUACCAUUAAAAAUAUUUUUAGGCAUCAUCAAACUUGUCACACAACCUGCACAUCCCCAUGCCCCACUCAAUAACACCACAAUCUCAGGGUCUCACAGUGUUGGAGAAUUUCCAUGGCUCAUCUAAGAGUUCUUCUCACUUAACAUUUUUUAUUGAAAAUUUUUACCGUAUCUAAGGAUUUGUGGGGUUCAAUUUGCCAAACUCCAAGGCAGUGGAAAAGAAGACAACUGCAUCAAGUCAGUUUCUGGUUUUAUAUAGUUUAACAGAAGAAUAAUUUGCUUAGAUCUUCGCCUUCAUAUUUGGAGGCAUAUACUCACACACACACACAUGCACACACACACGCACACACACACACACACACACAUGUUAUGCAUAGAUGAAUAAUAUUUAGUCUGCAAAGAAAUAGGCCUGUUUCCUCCGUCAUCUGUACCUUGCUAACCCAGAGACUUGACAUGGAGGAGGAAUGCAGAGAGCCUUUCACCCUUAAUGGAUUCCACAGCUGUGAGUCACCCUGGCCCCAGGCUUCUCGCCUUUGCCUCAUCCCAUUCCUGCUCUCACAGUCAGAGGUCUGGAUCUCCAGUUACUGACUUUGGAACUAGGGGGAAGAUGACACAGGUGACAUAAAACAAGAGCCCCCUUCUAUAUCUCAGAGCAAAUUCCUGAAAUAUACUACCAAAACAUAAAAGUGUGGACGUCAACUUUAGACAAAUCCUUGCCUUACAUUGAUUUGCAGAGCUCUUUAGAAAUCAGACCAUGGCUUUCAGUAUACAUUAUAUAAAUGUGUUCUUCACAACACGAUGCCAAGAAGCAGAUGUGCUCUCUGAGACCCACAGAGGUCAAGCAACUUCCCCAAAAUCAUAGCUGGUUGAUUGCCAGGACAGAGACCCAAACCUUGUCUUCUGACCAGCCCUUUCCAGUACACCAUGGAUGACUCACCCACAAAUGACAAAUGCUUUGUAGUCUUUUAAAGGAAGUUGGGGAUAUUCAGGGGACAUCCUCUAACCUUGUGAGAAUGUAUCAUCAUGGAAGGAAAUCACCAUCCUUUUCAUAGAGUAGUCCUUGGAGUCAGUUGCUGAGAUGGCUUGCUAUGGCUUUUGCAGGAUGGAUUUUAGUGAUGAUAAAGGACAUGGUAAAUAUUUGGUAAUAUAACAAAUGCCCAUGGAACUUGUAAACAGUACUAUCAUAAUUGUUUCCAUUUGUCUUAACCGCACUCGAAGCGAUAUCUCCUAACUCAUCCCCAAACUAAUAUGUCGAAAGCAACAGGCUCUGAUGGAGAGGGAAAGGGGUAAUGCUAACAGUACUCAGGAGACGGCAGGAACUAUAUUUUCUAAGAGUCAGAUUCCCUGCUAUUUCUGUUGUCUCAUUUAAUCCUCACUAUAUUGUUGUGCAGUGGAUGUAAUUUUAUUGUUAUUUCUAUUUAGCAUAUGAGAAAACAGAGGCUUUAGACAGGUUAAGUAACUUGCACACUUGUACUACGUGGUAGGUGUCAAAAAACUGGGAUGUGAACGCAGGUCAGUUGCGCUCUAUGCAUUGUGAAGUGCUGCCUACAAACCUCUUUGAGAUUAUUGAGAAAUGUGAUCCUGACAUUUCUGGAGGACUAGAGAAGUCCAUGAAAAUAUAUGGCUAGGAAUUACUGGCAACAGACUAUGUGCAAACUGACUUUUAGUAUUUCCUCAUUUAAUCCUUGUUAUAAUCCUAUGAAAUAGUACCAUCUUUACACUUUCUACAGUGAGGAAAUGGAAGCAGAGAGAGGUUAUACAACUUGCCAAGCAAGAUCUGACCAUUGUUAAUUGAUAAAGACUGGAUUUAAACCGGUAGGUGGGCUGCAAGCCCAUGCUCCUCACUGCCAUACUGGGUGCUGCUAGGCCGAGGUUCAAAACAACCCUUGUUGGCUGAAGGUUUUUUUGAGCUGGCUCAGCUCUGGGGUUGGUGCAUUCUGUAAAUGAUCAGUUUGACAGUGUAGGUAGUAGAGACAUGCUGCUUUAAGAAAGAACUUUGUAUCUCUAUUACAGAGAGAAGAUAUAAAGAUAUUAGUUCAGUCUUCCAUAACACGAUAUAACAGACUUUUCAUUUUUAUGCGGGAGGGAUCUCUAACUCUUUAGUCUUUAUCUUAAGGAAAAUGUAAAGGUAUUACAGGGUUGUAAGCAUGACAACAGAUGUGAUUAGAUUAGCUUUUUAAAUCUCUCACUCCAGAUGUUCAGCUGCAUUAGGUAACUACCUCAAGGUGAGUACCAAUGAAAACUCUUAAAUAAGUACUUUGUUCAAAGGAAUCCUUCAAGGUUUUCUAGGUCUGUGCUGUCCAGUGUGGUAGCCCUGAGCCACAGGUGGCUGUUGAGCACUUGAAACAGUGAAACAGCCCUUGAAACAGUGCCUGAUCCAAAUGGAUAUGGUGCUGUAAGUCUAAAAUAAACUGAAUUUUGAAGCUUAUUAGAAAAAAAGGAUGAAAUAUCUCAUUAGUAAGUUUUAUAUUGAUAAAUAUUGUAAGUUUUCUAUUGAUAAAUAUAAAAAUAUUAAGAUAAUAUUUUUGGAUAUAUUAGGCUAUGUGGACUGUGUUAUUGAAGUUAACUACACUUGUUUCUAGCUGCUAGAAAAUUUAAAAUUACAUACAUGGCUGGCAUGAUUUUUUAAUCUGACGCUGCUGGUCUAGGUAAUUUCCUUGCUCUCUAGUUAAAUAGGAAAUUUAUGGGAAUACCAUUAGCAUAGGUUGAUGCACUGCUUCUGAGUACCCUUUGUUUAAACUAUUCCAACCUAAGGUCUGUUGCUUCUUGGAUAAUAUUCCAUACCUUUAUUGGCACUGUUCUUUUAAAAUUCAGUUAAAAGUAUCAUUUUCCAUUUAUUACCAAAGAGUAGACUGUUCUUGACAUAUGUUAGAAAAAAUUGAGCUUAGACCACAGCUCAUUAGUUAACUCUGGAUGGGUCAGAAAGUGGUGACCUGGUUAUUAGACAGAGUGCACCAAGCAUUAGCUUCUGCCCGUGCUCCCUUCUAAAUAUCAUGUAGGCUUGACCCCUCCUCUUCAUCCCCAGUGCGUCGUCUGGCCCAGGCUUCCUUUAUCUCUUCCCUGGACCAUCUCAGCAGCUGCUUAGCAGCCUGUUUCCCACCAUCCUCUUCACCUCUAGGAGUCCCUCAUGAUGCUAGCAAAAUAAUCUUGAUAGGGCACAGCUUUCGUUAUAUCACAUUGCCCUGAUUAAGGAUGAUAAGAGAUCCCUGUUUCUGUCCGAAUGAAGGGAGGGAGGGAAGGCUCUGACAUUUGAAACUGGAUAGAUCUUACGUUAUUUAAUCCCUAUGAAAUGGAUAUUUUUUAGUCCCAUUAUACAGGUCAGGAAGUUGGAGGUCCUGUUGUCUUUCUUUGCUAAAACCUAUGUUAGUUCUAGUGACCUGUGCUGAUUGCUAGCUUUCAAGAACAUUCAUGGAAACAAAAACUUGGAACUCCUGUAAUGCCAUCUUUUUGGGGGUGGGAAUAUGUAUUGGGUUCUUCUUUCUUACAUAUGUUCAUGGAAUUAUUCAUAGACAAACCAUUCAGUCUGGUUAUGAUGUUCACCUCCCCUCUACAUCCUGGUUUUAUUUACUUAUGAGAAGAAAUGCAAUGCAAAAAAAACAAGAACAUUCAUUAUCUAACCCGCCCUUUCUAGCCUUAAAUCAUGUCCUUUUCUUUCCCAAUGGUCUAAUCAUAACUGCCCUCUCCAUCUCUUUACUUGGAAACUGUACCAUAACAAUCUAUGCCUUAUUAUAGAGUGUUUGGAAUUCUUCAUUGUCUGAUUUUUUUAAUGUUAGUCUCAUCCCAACUAUAUUUUUAACUUCCAUGAGAAAGAACAUGCCUUAUACCAGCCUUCUGUCCCCCUCAUUGUUUUUGUUUUUCUCUCACGUCUAGAACCAUACUAGCUACGUAGUAGGCACUCAAAUGUUUAGUUAGUGGAUGGUGCUGGCAUGUGGCAGCUGGUCAAUAAAUAUUUGUUUUUGGCUCAAUCGAAAAUGAUUUUUUUAAAAAAUGAGGGCAGAGAGCUUCAGAUCAAUGAUUCCCUCUUCACCAGUCUAGAUGUGAGGUAGAGUGGACCUUAGCAAUGACAGGACACUUCUAAGCCAGACUCAACCUCAUGGCGUCUCAGAUUUCCCACCUAAUCUCGGUUGCAGGAUGAGGUGGUCAUGGCUAGUAGUCCAUAUAGCUCCAGAAGGUAAUGGGUUAUAUUGCUUCUAAUAUUUCCUGGAGUGACAUUUAAGAUGUUUAUUUGUGUUUGGGGGAUAGAAGGUAAAGUAUAUAAUCCCCUGAGGACAGAACCUGUGUCCUCCUUAGGGCCUCCUAGAACGAAAUUGAACAUUAGAUCAGUGAGGUCGACUGAUUGAUGAAAUAUUUUGUUCAAAUAUGUGUUUCUGCUAAACCUUGCUGUCUCUUGUAUAGGAUACACCUGCUCCUGUCUGAAGUUUAUGAAGACAGAUCACAAGGCAUUGACAUUUGGUCCACUUGCUAAUAGGCAGUUAAUGUUCUGUGGUCAGUCUUGGCUGUGCCUCUUUUCUUCACGUGCCAACAUUAUUUUGUGGAUUCAUAUUAAGUAUUUAAACACCAAAGUGAUCACACACCCACACAUUCCCUAAAAUGUGGGCUGACUUGUUGGCCAACCAUUCAUGAACCUGGGGAUUUUUUGAGAGAAACUAUUUAAUUUGUUUUCUGAUUUCUCUGAAAACAUUUAAACAAACAGACAAAAAUUCCAACUUGUGAAACCCACAUACUAAUAAAAAUCACACAAACAUUAUAGAAGUUGGAAUUCAGAAAAAGUAAAACUUCUUUUCAACCUCCCUUUCAGAGAAAACUUCACCAGUAAAAGUUUAGGGUAUAUGGCUUCUGGUCAUUUUUCUAUAUUUAUAUAUUUGCAUCAUAUUAUUAUUAUCAGUAUUUGAGUAGAAACAGAUUAUGUAUUAUGUUUUGCAACUUAUUUUUUCACUUAACUAUAAACAUGAAAGAACACUUCCCCUAAGAAUUCCCUUAGUACAGGUUUUGGUAUGCAGGAAAAAGAACUAGAUGCCUGGGGUUCUUAGCUUUGGUGACAAGAUAACUUUGUCUACACUGUUGAACUUUUGCCAUCAGUGACCUCAUUCUACUUUAAUAUGUCGAUCUUUGAAGACUUACUUUUUUUUUUUAGUAAUUCCAUGGAAAUAAACUAUUUGGAGACCAGUUCUUUUCAGUUGUGAUGCUUCUCAUCCCCUAAAUACACCAGUCUUCUGGAAUGUAGUAAUGUUUUAUGAGUAAAAAUUAUGUUUUGUAAGGGCACUCCUCUUUGUCUGAAGUUCAUUGCCAGAGGCAGGGACAGAAUAAGGAGCACAGUAAUAUAAUAUGCACAAGGAUAUGAGAAAAGGAAGACAAAGGUAGAAGUAUCCUUAAGUUUGAAAAUGCCAGAUCUGCUAGACAGUCUUAAGACAAGGAUGGCAUUGAGAUUAGGGAAGGAGAAUAGAGAGGGAAAGAGGCCAGCAGCAGGGCCCUGCUGAUCCAUGGAUUCGCCUCCAGCCACAAGCCAGUCCCUAGCUCAUGGCCAUAUGGGACUGAGGCUAAAGCCGUGCUCUAAUUCUGAUCCUCAGCUUCUCCACCAGCCCUCUCCCUCCCCCUACAAACAUACAGCCUUGCAGUUCCUCAGCAUUAGCAAAUGUGUAAUUCCUUAUUUCGUCAGUGCUAAGUUGCACUUUUCCCCACAUUUAUACAUUUCUCAAAAGGGAUGCAUGUUAUCAUCAGUUUAUAUUUAAUGUGCAUGGAGUCCUCUCUUGAAACUUUGUUAUUAAACUAAGUCUUAUAAUAACAUUUGGAGGAAGAACUCCAAAUAGAGGAAGAACAAUGUAUGGGUUCUGGACUCUGCCUGGAGAUGGGUUUGAACAGAACAGAACACAGUCCCUGCUUUCAAGAAACUCACAAUGCGCUGUGGGGAAAGAGACAACUAAGUGGAUGGUGCUGUGUGAAAAUGUUUGGGAGAUUCAGGGGUCCCUAGGAAGGGUCUACCCCAGCCUUGAGGUGCCAGGAAAGGCCUUCUAGAGAAAGUGGUACUCAAUUGGGUAUGAUUUUGUGCUAACCCUUCUGGAGGUGGAGGGGGGGUCAUUUGGUAGUGUCUCCAGAGAGACAGUUGAAGCACUGUUGGUUGUCACUACUGGGGAUGAGGGAAGAUGCUACCAGCAUCUAGUGGGGAUGUCAGGGAUACUGCUAAAUAUCCUACAAUGCCCAGGACAGCCUCUCACAAUAAUUAUCAGGCUUCAAAUGGGAAUAGCACCCCGAGUUUGAGAAACCCUCCUGUAAGUUGAGAUUGAGGGAUGAAUACAAAUUGGUGGUGCUGGGGGAGGAGGUCAGGGUGGAGAGAGUCAUAGGUGUCCAGGAAAGGGAGUUAUUUGGAGGAAGAGUUUGCCAUGAUGGAGAAUGGUACAGAAACAAUGGUUUUGUAUGGUUUAGAAGCAAAAGUAUCCUAUUAUUGCUCCUAAGAAGGUUGUUGCUGACCAUGAUGAAUUUGGUUUAGCAGAAUCAGAGUUACAAAAGCCAGAUGUAGAAGACUGAAGGAGAAGUAAGGAACAUGAAAGCAGUUUGUGAAAAGGAGGAAUUAAUGAUAACAAUGGCAAUUGUAGUUAAGUUUUUGUAUAUGCCAGAAACUAUGCCAAAUGCUUUAUGUUCCUUAUCCAGAUUAUUCUACACAACCCUGUGAUAUAUGGAUUACUUGGUAUGGAUGAGGAAACAGAGGUUUGGAGAAUUUAAAUAGUUUGUCAAGGAUUCAUGUAGCUAAUAAAUCAUAGAGUCGGGAUUCAACCUCAGGCCUCUUUGACUCUUACCUAUAAUUUCCCUAGAGAAGAAGUUAGGCCAGAGGGACAUGGAGAGAGAGAGAGAGAGAGAGAAUGUGUGUGUAUGUGUGUGUGUGUGGGGGGGGGGGGGUGUGUGCAUGCAUGCAUGUGUGUUUUCUCCCCUAGAUGGGUGAGAGUUUAAGGUGGGGAUGACUUAGCUAGUAGUCAAAGAUAAAUUGAAAAUGCAGAAAGGAUAACUAUCAGACCAUCUCGCAGAUGAGGCAGUGAGGACUGACUCAAGAGCUCAAGUUAAGGAAUCAGCCUUAGAUGAUGGGACAUGGGAGCGCCACUUCCAUUGUGGCACGAGGAUAAGAGAGAAAAGAUAGGUGUCUGUGCAGAUGAGGAAGGGAAACCCUGAGAGAAAAUGGAAUCCUCCUCCUCUUCUCAGUUAGACACAGUGAGCAAUGGGAGACAGACUUAACUAUGUGAACAUCAGAUUACUGGGUGGAGUUGAGACCAUGAAUUUGCAGGGACACCAAUCUGAGGAUAUGCAAAAAGAAUUUGGGAGAAAACACUCAUUUAAGAUUGUUCCAGAGUUGACAUUUUUUUCAGAUGGUUAUGUGGGAAAGGCAAAGGACUGGGUUGCAUAACAACAGCUCAUUCUCAGGUUUCCCUCCACCUGCUUAAAUUCCUUUAGGAGGAGAUAGUGUGGCUUUUCUUUUUUUUUAAUUUUAAUUUUAUUUAAUUGUUUUACUUUUCCAUAAGUUAUUGGGGUACAGGUGGCAUUUGGUUACAUGAGUAAGUUCUUUAGUGGUGACGUGUGACAUUUUGGUGCACCCAUCACCCACAUAUACACUGCACCAUAUUUGUAGUCUUUUAUCUCUUGCCCCCCUCCCACUCUUCCCCCCAAGUCCCCAAAGUCCAUUGUAUUGUUUUUAUGCCUUUGUGUCUUCAUAGCUUAGCUCCCAAAUAUCAGUGAGAACAUACGAUGUUUGGUUUUCCAUUCCUGAGUUAAUCACUUAGAAUAAUAGUCUCCAGUCUUAUCCAGGUCACUGCAAAUGCUGUUAAUUCAUUCCUUUUUAUGGCUGCAUAGUAUUCCAUCGUGUGUGUGUGUGUGUGUGUGUGUGUGUGUGUGUGUGUGUGUGUGUGUGUAUCUCACAGUUUUUUAAUCCACUCGUUGAUUGAUGGGCAUCUGGGUUGGUUCCAAGAUUUUGCAAUUGUGAAUUGUGCUGCUAUAAACAUGGGUGUGCAAGUAUCUUUUUCGAAUAAUGACUUCAUUUCCUCUGGGUAGAUACCCAGUAGUGGGAUUGCUGGAUCAAAUGGUAGUUCUACUUUUAGCUCUUUAAGGAUCUCCACACUGUUACACUGUUUUCCACAGUGGUUGUACUAGUUUAGUUCCCACCAGCAGUGUAGAAGUGUUCUCUGUUCACCGCAUCCAUGCCAACAUCUACUGUUUUUUGAUUUUUUGAUUAUGGCCAUUCUUGCAGGAGUAAGAUGGCAUUGCAUUGUGGUUUUAAUUUGCAUUUCCCUGAUCAUUAGUGAUGUUGAGCAUUUUUUCAUGUUUGUUGGCCAUUUGUAUCUCUUCUUUUGAGAAUUGGCUAUUCAUGUCCUUCACCUACUUUUUGAUGGGAUUGUUGUUUUCUUACUGAUUUGUUUGAAUUUGUUGUAGUUUCUGGAUAUUAGUCUUUUGCCAGAUGUAUAGAUUGUGGAUGAUUUUUCUCCUACUCUGUGGGUUGUCUGUUUACUUUGCUGACUCUUCCUUUUGCUGUGCAAAAGCUCUUUACUUUAAUUAGGUCCCAGCGAUUUAUCUUUGUUUGUAUUGCACUUCCUUUUGGCUUCUUGGUCAUGAAAUCUUUGCAUAAGCCAAUGUCUAGAAGGAUUUUUCCAAUGUUAUCUUCUAAAAUUUUUAUAGUUUCAGGUCUUAGAUUUAAGUCUUUAAUCCAUCUUGAGUUGAUUUUUGUAUAAAGUAAGAGAUGAUCCAGUUUCAUUCUCCUACAAGUGGCUAACCAGUUAUCCCAGUAAUUGGCUAAUUGGAUAAUUUCAACAAAUUUCAACCAUUUGUUGAAAAGGAUGUUCUUUCCCCACUUUAUGUUUUUGUUUGCUUUGUUGAAGAUCAGUUGGCUGUAAGUAUUUGGGAUUAUUUCUGGGUUCUCUAUUCUCUUCCACUGGUAUACGUGCCUAUUUUUAUACCAGUACCAUGCUGUUUUGGUGACUAUGCCCUUACAGUAUAGUUUGAAAUCAGGUAGUGUGAUGCCUCUAGAUUUGUUCUUUUGCUUAGUCUUCCUUUGGCUAUGUGGGCUAUUUUUUGGUUCCAUAUGAAUUUUAGAAUUGUUUUUUCUAAUUCUGUGAAGAAUGAUGGUGGUAUUCUGACGGAGAUUGCAUUGAAUUUGUACAUUGCUUUUGGCAGUAUGGUCAUUUUCACAAUAUUGAUUCUACCCAUCCAUGAGCAUGGGAUGUGUUUCCUUUUGUUUGUGUCAUCUAUAAUUUCUUUCAGCAAUGUUUUCUAGUUUUCCUUGUAGGGGUGUUUUGCCUCCUUGGUUAGGUAUAUUCCUAAGUACUUAUUUUAUUUUUUGCAGCUAUUGUAAAAGGGGUUGAGUUCUUGAUUUGAUUCUCUGCUUGGCUGCUGUUGGUGUCCAGAAGAGCUAAUUUGUGUACAUUAAUGCUGUAUCUAGAAACUUUGCUGAAUUCUUUUAUCAGUUCUAGGAGAUUUCUGGAGGAGUUCUUAGGGUUUUCAAGGUAAACAAUCCUAUUGUCAGCAAACAAACAGUGACAGUUUGGCUUCCUCUUUACCGAUUUGGAUGCCUUUUAUUUCUUUCUAUUGUCUGAUUGCUCUCGCUAGAACUUUCAACACUGUGUUGAAGUGGAGUGGUGAGAGUGGACAUCCUUGUCUUGUUCCAGUUCUCAGAGGGAGAGCUUUCAACUUUCCCCAUUCAGUAUUAUGCUGGCUGUGGGUUUGUCAUAGAUGGCUUUUAUUACAUUAAGGUAUGUCUCUCGUAUGCUGAUUUUGCCAAGCGUUUUAAUCAUAAAGGGAUGCUGGAUUUUGUCGAAUGCUUUUUCUGCCUCUAUUGAGAUGAUCAUGUGAUUUUUUAUUUUUAAUUCUGUUUAUGUGGUGUAUCACAUUUAUUGACUCAUGUAUGUUAAACCAUCCCUGCAUCCCUGGUAUGAAACCCACUUGAUCAUGGUGGAUUAUCUUUUUGAUAUGUUGUUGAAUUUGGUUAGCUAGUAUUUUGUUAAGGAUUUUAGCAUCUAUAUUCAUCAAGGAUAUUGGUCUGUAGUUUUCUUCUGUGGUUAUGUCGUUUCCUGGUUUUGGUAUUAGAGUGCUGCUGGAUUCAUAGAAUGAAUUAGGGAGGGUUCUCUCUCUCUCUCUGUCUUGUGGAAUAGUGUCAAAAGGACUGGUACAAAUUCUUUUUUGAAUGUCUCGUAGAAUUCUGCUGUGAAUCCAUCUGGUCCUGGACUUUUUUUGUUGGUAAUUUUUUAAUUUAUCAUUUCAAUCUCACUGCUUGUUAUUGGUCUGUUCAGGGUACCUAAUUCUUCCUGAUUUAAGCUGGGAGGGUUGUAUUUUUCCAGGAAUUUAUCCAUCUCUCCUAGGUUUUCUAGUUUAUGUGCAUAAAGAUGUUCAUAGUAACCUUGAAUGAUCUUUUUGUAUUUCUGUGGUAUCAGAUGUAAUAUCACCUGUUUUGUUUCUUAGUGAGGUUAUUUGGAUUUUCUCUCUUCUUUUCUUGGUUAAUUUUGCUAAUGGUCUAUCAAUUUUAUUUAUCUUCUCAAAGAACCAGCUUUUGUUUCAUUUAUCUUUUGUGUUUUUUUUGUUUGUUUGUUUGAAUUUCAUUUAGUUUUGCCCUGAUCUUGGUUAUUUCCUCCCUUCUGCUGGGUUUGGGUUUGGUUUAUUCUUAUUUAUCUGUUUCCUUGAGGUGUGACCUUAGAUUGUCUGUUUGUGCCCUUUCAGACUUUUUGAUGUAGAUGUAGGCAUUUAGAGCUAUGAAUUUUCCUCUUAGCACCACCUUUGCUUUGUCCCAGAGGUUUUGAUAGGUUGUGUCAUUAAGUUCGAAGAAUUUUUAAAUUUCCAUCUUGAUGUCAUUUUUGACCCAAUGUUCAUUCAGGACCAGAUUAUUUAAUUUCCAUGUAUUUUCAUGGUUUGGAAGGUUCCUUUUGGAAUUGCUUUCCAGUUUUAUUCCACUGUGGUCUGAGAGAGUGCUUAAAAUAAUUUUAAUUUUCUGAAAUUUAUUGAGGCUCAUUUUGUGGCCUAUCAUAUGGUCUAUCUUGGAGAACAUUCCAUGUGCUGGUGAAUGGAAUGUGUAUUCUGCAGUUGUUGGAUGAAGUGUUUUGUAUAUAUCUGUUAAGUCCAUUUGUUCCAAGGUAUAGUUUAAAUCCACUGUUUCUUUGUUGACUUCCUAUCUUGAUGACCUGUCUAGUACUGUCAGUGUAAUAUUGAAGCCCCCACUAUUAUUGUGUUGUUAUCUCAUUUCUUAGGUCUAUUAGUAAUUAUUUUAUAAAUUUGGGAGCUGCAGUGUUAGGUGCAUAUAUGUUCACAAUUGUGAUAUUUUCCUGUUAGACAAGGCCUUUUACCAUUGUAUACUGUCCCUCUUUGUCUCCUUUAACCACUGUUGCUUUAAAGUUUGUUUUGUCUGAUAUAAGAAUAGUUACCCCUGCUCACUUUUGGUGUCCAUUUGCAUGAAAUGCCUUUUUCCACCCCUUUAAAUUUAUGUAAGUCCUUAUGUGUUAGUUGAGUCUCCUGAAGGCAGCAGAUAGUUGGUUGGUGACUUCUUAUAUAUUCUGUGGUUCUGUAUCUUUUAAGUGGAGCAUUUAGGCCAUUUACAUUCAAUAUCAGUAUUGAAAUGUGAGGUACCAUUGCUUUCAUCAUGCUCAUUGUUGCCUGUGUACUUUGGUUUUUUGUUUUUGUUUUUUAACUUGUAUUUUUGUUUUAUAGGUCCUGUGUGAUUUAUGUUUUAAAGAGAUUCUGUUUUGAUGUGUUUCCAGGGUUUAAGAUUUAGAGUUCCUUUUAGCAGUUCUCGUAGUGGUGGUUUGGUAAUGGCGAAUUCUCCCAGCAUUUGUUUGUCUGAAAACAAGUGUAUCUUUCCUUCAUAUAUUAUGCUUAGUUUUGGGGGAUACAAAAUUCUUUGCUGAUAAUUGUUUUGUUUGAGGAGAGUGAAGAUAGGUCCCCAAUCCCUUCUAGCUUGUAGGGUUUCUGCUGAGAAAUCUUCUGUUAAUCUGAUAGGUUUUCCUUUAUAGGUUACCUGGUGCUUCUGUCUCACAGCUCUUAAGAUUCUUUCCUUUGUCUUAACUUUGGAUAACUUGAUGACAGUGUGCCUAGGUGAAGAUCUUUUUGCAAUGAAUUUCCCAGGUGUUCUUUGUGCUUCCUAUAUUUGGCUGUCUAGGUCUCUCACAAGGCUGGGGAAGUUUUCCUCAAUUAUUCCCCCCGAUAUGUUUUCUAGGCUUUCAGAAUUCUCUUCUUCCUCAGGUACACUGAUUAUUCUUAGGUUUGGUCAUUUAGCAUAACCCCAGACUUCUUGGAUGUUUUGUUCAUAUUUUCUUAUUCUUUUUCUUUGUCUUUGUUGGAUUGGGUUAAUUUGAAGACCUUAUCUUCAAGCUCUGAAUUUCUUUCUUCUGCUGAGACUUUACAGAGCAUUUUGCAUUUCUAAAAGUGUGUCCAAAGUUUUCUGAAUUUUUGAUUGUUUUUUUUCUUUAAGCUAUCUGUUUCCAUGAAUAUCUCUCCCUUCUCUUCUUGUAUCAUUUUUUGGACUUCCUUGCAUUGGGCUUUACCUUUCUCUGGUCUCGCCCUGAUUAGCUUAAUAACUAACCUCCUGAAUUCUUUUUCAGAUAAAUCAGGGAUUUCUUCUUGGUUUGGAUCCAUUGCUGGUGAACUAGUGUGAUUUUUUUGUGGGGGGGUGUUGAAGAGCCUUGUUUUGUCAUAUUACCAGGGUUGGUUUUCUGGUUUCUUCUCAUUUGGGUAGGCUCUGUCAGAGGGAAGGUCUAUGGCUGAAGACUGUUGUUCAGAUUCUUUUGUCCCAAGGGGUGUUCCCUUGAUGUGUAGUACUCUCCCCCUUUUCCUAUGGAUGUGGCUUCCUAUGAGCCAAACUUCAGUGAUUGUUAUCUCUCUUCUGGGUCUAGCUACCCAGCGAGUCCACCCAGCAACAGGCUGGUUGGGGGUUUCUGCACAGAGUCCUGUGAUGUGAAUUGUCUAAGGGGUCUCUCAGCCAUGGAUACCAGCACCUGUUCUGGUGGAGGUGGCAGAGUGUGCAAUGGACUCUCUGAGGGUCCUUAGCUUUGGUGAUUUAAUGGUCUAUUUUUGUGCUCAUUGGCCUCCUGCCAGGAGGUGGCACUUUCUAAAAACUGUCAGCUAUAGUAGUGUGGAGAGAGACCAGAGGUGGGCGGGGCCCUAGAAUCCCCAAGAUUAUAUGCCCUUUGUCUUCCACUACUAGGGUGGGUAGGGAAGGACCAUCAGGUAGGGUGGGGAGAGAUGUGUCUGAGCUUAGACUCUCCUUGGGCAGGUCUUGCUGCGGCUGCUGUGGGAGAUGAGGGUGAGAUUCCCAGGUCACUGGAGUUGUGUACCUAGGAGGAUUAUGGCUGCCUCUGCUGAGUCGUACAGGUUGUCAGGGAAGUGGGGGAAAGCCAGCAGUCAUGAAGGGCUGGUCUCACUCUCACCGUGACCCCCGCAACAGCCCCGAGUCUGUUUCCAGGUGGAGGGCGAGAUGGGCUUGAAAAUUUCUCUGAGGCUACGCACCUCCCAGCUGCGAGAAAAAAGAGUUUUAGUUCUUCCACACCUGUGUAGUCUGCACGCCGGAUUUAUGCCCUCCCCGGAGUUCUGGCCAGGAGGCUUCUCACCACGUUUAAAUUGUUACAAAGUUCAGCUACAGAGUUCCUUCUCCCUGUGGAGUUUUACCCCCUGCUCCUCUGGCCACCCUCCCAAUGGAUCCCUGUGAUGCCAGGCAGGAAUGGGCCGCUUGGGGACCCAGUGAGAUCCCAGGGCCUUCCUGCUGCUUCCUCUACCCCUGUAUUUCACUUGGCUCUCUAACUUGACUCAGCUCCAGGUAAAGUCGGAAACUUCUGCAAACAGACCUUCAGCUUCUCCAGUGGGGGGUGUGUGUUUGGGAGAGGAGGGUCUCCCUUUCCCAUUUCUGCAGCUGGGGCACUCACAGUAUUUGCAGUGUCUCCUGGGUCCUGCAGGAGCAGUCUGCUCUUUUCAGAGGGCCUGUGGGGUCCUCUUGGGAUUGCUGGUUUGUUCUUGCAGUCAAUCUGGAGCUAAAAUUCACAAUGCAAGCCUCCGCAUGCUGCUCUGCCUGGAGCUACAAUCUAUUCCUGCCUCCCUUCUGCCGUGAUAACAGAGAUCCCUGCUUUUCCUUUAAAGGUUCCUAAUGUGAGAGGCUAGACCCAGAUCAUGGAGGUGCUUCAGUGUGAUGGCUGUGAUUUCCGAGCCCCGUCUUAUGAAGAUCUCAAGGCACACAUUCAGGAUGUCCACACGGCAUUUCUGCAGCCAACUGAUGUUGCUGAGGACAAUGUGAAUGAGCUACGAUGUGGGUCCGUGAAUGCCAGUAAUCAGACAGAGGUGGAGUUUUCUUCUAUAAAGGAUGAAUUUGCCAUUGCAGAAGAUUUAUCAGGUCAAAAUGCAACUUCAUUGGGGACCGGAGGUUACUAUGGCCACAGUCCAGGAUAUUAUGGUCAGCAUAUUGCCGCUAAUCCCAAACCAACAAACAAGUUUUUUCAAUGCAAGUUCUGUGUACGCUACUUCAGGUCAAAAAACCUCCUCAUAGAACACACUAGAAAGGUCCAUGGAGCUCAAGCUGAAGGGAGUUCAUCAGGACCCCCUGUCCCGGGAUCCUUAAAUUAUAAUAUCAUGAUGCACGAGGGAUUUGGAAAGGUCUUCUCUUGCCAGUUUUGCACAUACAAGUCACCAAGAAGGGCAAGAAUAAUUAAGCAUCAGAAGAUGUAUCACAAAAACAAUUUGAAGGAGACCACUGCUCCCCCACCUGCUCCUGCUCCAAUGCCAGACCCUGUGGUUCCGCCCGUAUCACUGCAGGACCCCUGCAAGGAACUGCCAGCAGAGGUUGUGGAGCGCAGCAUCUUAGAGUCUAUGGUCAAGCCUUUGACCAAAUCUCGAGGCAACUUUUGUUGUGAGUGGUGCAGCUACCAGACCCCCCGCCGAGAACGCUGGUGUGACCACAUGAUGAAGAAACACCGCAGUAUGGUCAAGAUCCUUUCCAGUCUCAGACAGCAACAAGAAGGAACUAAUCUACCUGAUGUGCCGAACAAGAGUGCCCCCAGCCCCACUUCCAACUCCACCUAUCUGACCAUGAAUGCUGCAAGCCGGGAGAUACCCAAUACUACCGUCUCCAACUUCAGGGGCUCCAUGGGCAACUCCAUCAUGAGACCCAAUUCUUCAGCUUCCAAGUUUUCGCCCAUGUCUUACCCUCAGAUGAAGCCGAAGUCACCUCACAAUUCUGGUCUAGUUAACUUGACAGAGAGAUCCCGUUAUGGAAUGACUGACAUGACCAAUUCUUCUGCUGACCUGGAAACUAACAGCAUGCUAAAUGACUCUAGUUCUGAUGAAGAGUUAAAUGAAAUAGACAGUGAGAAUGGUUUAAGUGCUAUGGAUCACCAGACAUCAGGCCUGUCUGCAGAGCAGCUGAUGGGCUCAGAUGGCAACAAAUUAUUGGAGACCAAGGGGAUUCCAUUUAGAAGAUUCAUGAAUAGGUUCCAGUGCCCCUUUUGUCCUUUCCUCACCAUGCAUCGACGUAGCAUCUCUCGUCACAUAGAAAACAUCCACUUAUCUGGAAAGACAGCUGUCUACAAAUGUGACGAAUGUCCGUUUACUUGCAAGAGCUCGUUGAAACUUGGGGCUCACAAACAGUGUCACACGGGUACAACGUCAGAUUGGGAUGCUGUGAAUUCCCAGAGUGAAAGCAUUUCUUCCUCACUGAAUGAAGGUGUGGUGUCUUAUGAGAGCUCAAGCAUCAAUGGUAGAAAGUCAGGAGUCAUGUUGGAUCCCUUGCAGCAGCAACAGCCACCGCAGCCACCACCACCGCCGCCGCCACCACCACCAUCACAGCCACAGCCACUGCAGCAGCCACAGCCACCACAGCUGCAGCCACCACAUCAGGUGCCACCCCAGCCACAAACACAGCCACCACCAACGCAGCAGCCACAGCCACCCACACAAGCCGCACCUCUGCACCCAUACAAAUGCACCAUGUGUAAUUACUCCACCACAACUCUGAAAGGGCUAAGAGUCCAUCAGCAGCAUAAACAUUCAUUCUGUGACAACUUGCCAAAAUUCGAGGGGCAGCCCUCAAGCCUACCAUUGGAAAAUGAGACAGACAGCCACCCCUCUUCCAGCAACACUGUGAAGAAAAGUCAGACCUCAAUUCUUGGGUUGUCCUCCAAGAACAAUUUUGUAGCUAAAGCCUCUAGGAAGCUCGCCAAUGACUUUCCUCUAGAUUUGUCACCCGUGAAGAAGAGAACCAGGAUUGACGAGAUAGCAAGCAACCUUCAGAGCAAAAUUAACCAAACCAAACAGCAGGAAGAUGCAGUGAUCAAUGUUGAGGAUGAUGAAGAGGAAGAGGAAGACAACGAAGUCGAGAUAGAGGUUGAGUUGGACAGGGAGGAAGAACCGACAGAACCCAUCAUAGAGGUUCCCACUUCCUUUUCUGCCCAACAGAUAUGGGUAAGAGAUACCAGUGAGCCCCAGAAAGAGCCCAACUUCAGAAACAUCACCCACGAUUACAAUGCCACCAAUGGGGCUGAGAUUGAGCUCACCCUUUCUGAAGAUGAAGAGGAUUAUUAUGGCUCCUCAACAAACUUGAAAGAUCACCAAGUUUCCAAUACUGCUCUGCUGAAUACCCAAACUCCCAUCUAUGGGACUGAGCACAAUAGUGAAAACACAGACUUUGGUGACUCUGGAAGGCUUUACUAUUGUAAACACUGUGACUUUAACAACAAAUCUGCCCGGAGUGUUAGCACCCACUACCAACGAAUGCACCCAUACAUUAAAUUCAGCUUUAGGUACAUCUUGGACCCCAAUGAUCACAGUGCAGUGUACAGGUGCCUGGAAUGCUACAUCGAUUACACCAACUUCGAAGAUCUCCAGCAGCAUUAUGGCGAGCACCACCCAGAAGCCAUGAAUGUACUCAACUUUGAUCACUCGGACCUGAUCUACCGGUGUCGGUUUUGUUCAUACACGAGCCCGAAUGUUAGAAGCCUGAUGCCACAUUACCAAAGAAUGCAUCCCACGGUGAAGAUCAACAACGCGAUGAUAUUUUCAAGCUAUGUCGUGGAGCAGCAGGAAGGGCUGAAUACAGAAUCCCAGACCCUGAGGGAGAUUCUGAAUUCGGCUCCCAAGAACAUGGCGACUUCCACACCUGUGGCUCGUGGUGGUGGUUUGCCAGCUACGUUCAACAAAAACACUCCUAAGACCUUUACUCCUGAAUGUGAAAAUCAGAAGGACCCUUUGGUCAACACUGUUGUUGUUUAUGAUUGUGAUGUUUGUUCGUUUGCAAGCCCCAACAUGCAUUCUGUCUUGGUUCAUUAUCAGAAGAAACACCCCGAAGAAAAGGCUUCCUACUUUAGGAUCCAGAAAACUAUGCGAAUGGUGUCUGUGGACAGGGGCUCUGCCCUUUCUCAAUUAUCAUUUGAGGUGGGUGCUCCAAUGUCUCCCAAAAUGUCCAACAUGGGUUCCCCACCCCCCCCACAACCCCCGCCACCAGACCUCAGUACUGAGCUUUACUACUGCAAACACUGUUCCUACAGCAAUCGGUCAGUUGUGGGAGUGCUUGUCCACUACCAGAAAAGACACCCAGAAAUAAAGGUUACUGCCAAAUAUAUCAGACAGGCUCCUCCCACAGCUGCAAUGAUGAGAGGGGUCGAAGGGCCCCAAGGCUCCCCCCGGCCACCCGCCCCCAUACAACAGCUGAACCGAAGCAGCUCUGAGAGAGAUGGCCCUCCUGUGGAGAAUGAGAUGUUCUUUUGCCAGCACUGUGAUUAUGGGAACCGGACGGUCAAAGGGGUACUCAUUCAUUAUCAGAAGAAGCACCGAGACUUCAAGGCCAAUGCAGAUGUGAUCCGGCAGCAUACGGCCACCAUUCGAAGCCUCUGCGACCGAAAUCAGAAGAAGCCUGCCAGCUGCGUGCUUGUCUCCCCCUCUAAUCUGGAGCGGGACAAAACGAAACUCCGAGCACUCAAAUGUAGGCAGUGCUCAUAUACCUCCCCCUACUUCUAUGCACUGAGGAAGCAUAUCAAGAAAGACCACCCCGCCCUGAAAGCCACAGUCACGUCCAUCAUGCGAUGGGCAUUUCUAGAUGGCUUGAUAGAAGCUGGCUACCACUGCGAGUGGUGCAUCUACUCCCAUACGGAGCCCAACGGUUUGCUCCUGCAUUACCAACGGAGGCAUCCAGAACACUAUGUUGAUUACACCUACAUGGCUACUAAACUGUGGGCUGGGCCAGACCCAUCCCCUCCCUCUCUCACAAUGCCAGCCGAAGCCAAAACCUACAGAUGCAGGGACUGUGUUUUCGAAGCUGUUUCCAUCUGGGACAUCACUAAUCACUACCAAGCAUUCCACCCCUGGGCCAUGAAUGGUGAUGAGUCAGUGCUACUGGACAUCAUCAAGGAGAAAGAUGCUGUGGAGAAGCCCAUUCUUUCAUCCGAAGAGUUGGCAGGCCCUGUGAAUUGUGAAAACAGUAUACCCACCCCUUUCCCGGAGCAGGAAGCUGAAUGUCCAGAGGAUGCAAGACUGUCCCCUGAGAAAAGCCUGCAGCUAGCUUCAGCCAACCCCGCCAUAUCCUCCACCCCAUACCAGUGCACGGUAUGCCAAUCUGAGUAUAACAACUUGCACGGCCUUCUCACUCAUUAUGGGAAGAAGCACCCUGGCAUGAAAGUGAAGGCUGCUGACUUUGCCCAGGACAUUGACAUCAACCCAGGUGCCGUCUACAAAUGCAGGCAUUGCCCAUACAUCAACACCCGCAUCCACGGCGUACUGACCCACUACCAGAAGCGACACCCGUCCAUCAAGGUGACCGCUGAGGACUUUGUGCACGACGUAGAGCAGUCUGCUGACAUAUCCCAGAAUGACGUGGAGGAGACGAGCAGGAUCUUCAAGCAAGGGUAUGGCGCCUACCGGUGCAAACUGUGUCCGUACACACACGGCACUUUGGAGAAACUAAAAAUCCACUACGAGAAGUAUCACAAUCAGCCUGAAUUUGAUGUCUUUUCCCAGUCGCCCCCGAAGCUGCCAGUCCCCCUCGAGCCCGAGAUGACCACUGAAGUGAGCCCUUCCCAAGUCUCCAUCACUGAGGAGGAGGUGGGAGAGGAGCCCGUGUCCACUUCUCACUUCUCUACCUCCCACCUGGUCUCCCACACUGUGUUCCGGUGCCAGCUCUGCAAGUACUUCUGCUCCACGAGGAAGGGGAUCGCCAGGCACUACCGCAUCAAGCACAAUAAUGUCCGAGCCCAGCCAGAAGGCAAGAACAACCUCUUCAAGUGUGCCCUGUGUGCCUACACCAACCCCAUCCGCAAAGGUCUGGCAGCCCACUACCAGAAGCGCCACGACAUUGAUGCGUAUUACACUCACUGCUUGGCAGCCUCCAGGACCAUCAGCGACAAGCCCAACAAAGUGAUCAUCCCAUCCCCGCCCAAGGACGACUCCCCUCAGCUGAGCGAGGAACUCCGGCGGGCAGUGGAGAAGAAAAAGUGCUCCUUGUGCUCUUUCCAGUCGUUCAGCAAGAAGGGCAUCGUGUCCCAUUACAUGAAACGCCACCCAGGGGUGUUCCCAAAGAAGCAGCACGCCAGCAAGUUGGGGGGCUACUUCACGGCCGUCUAUGCAGAUGAGCAUGAGAAGCCCACACUGAUGGAAGAAGAGGAGAGAGGCAACUUUGAGAAAGCCGAGGUGGAGGGUGAAGCUCAGGAAAUCGAGUGGCUCCCAUUCCGCUGCAUCAAAUGCUUCAAGCUGUCCUUUAGCACUGCAGAGCUGCUGUGCAUGCAUUACACUGACCACCACAGUCGGGACCUAAAGAGGGACUUCAUCAUUCUGGGCAACGGCCCCCGCUUGCAGAACUCCACCUACCAGUGUAAGCACUGUGAUAGCAAACUGCAAAGCACAGCCGAGCUGACCUCACACUUGAACAUUCACAAUGAGGAAUUCCAGAAGCGUGCCAAACGUCAGGAGAGGAGGAAACAGCUUUUGAGCAAGCAGAAAUAUGCAGAUGGUGCUUUUGCAGAUUUCAAACAAGAGAGGCCUUUUGGUCACUUAGAAGAGGUGCCAAAGAUCAAGGAGAGGAAAGUGGUGGGCUACAAAUGUAAAUUCUGUGUGGAAGUGCACCCAACGCUCCGAGCCAUCUGCAAUCACCUCCGAAAGCACGUCCAGUAUGGCAAUGUCCCAGCUGUGUCAGCUGCUGUGAAGCAGGAGGCGGAUGACCCUGCCCACUUGUUCCUGGAUGGAUUGGAAGCAGCCAAAGACGCCAGUGGCGCCCUGGUGGGCCGGGUGGAUGGUGAACACUGCUUGCUUGAUGGAAUGUUGGAGGAUGAAACCCGGCCGGGGGGAUACCAUUGCAGUCAAUGUGACAGAGUCCUGAUGUCCAUGCAGGGGCUGCGUUCUCAUGAGAGGAGCCACCUGGCCCUGGCCAUGUUUACCCGCGAGGACAAGUACAGCUGCCAGUAUUGCUCGUUUGUUUCUGCUUUCAGGCACAAUUUGGAUCGCCAUAUGCAAACCCACCACGGACACCAUAAACCAUUCCGAUGCAAACUCUGCUCCUUCAAGUCCUCCUAUAACAGCCGGCUGAAAACACAUAUACUCAAAGCUCAUGCUGGUGAGCAUGCCUACAAGUGUUCUUGGUGCUCAUUCUCCACCAUGACAAUCAGCCAGCUGAAGGAACACUCCCUCAAGGUCCACGGAAAAGCCCUGACCCUCCCCAGGCCACGGAUCGUCAGUCUCCUCUCCUCACACUCCCACCACUCCUCCCAAAAAGCUACCCCGGCUGAAGAAGUGGAAGACUCCAAUGACUCAUCAUAUUCAGAGCCCCCAGAUGUUCAGCAGCAGUUGAACCACUAUCAGUCAGCUGCCCUGGCAAGGAACAACAGCCGUGUUAGCCCUGUGCCUCUUUCUGGGGCUGCUGCUGGCACUGAGCAGAAAACUGAAGCCGUGCUUCACUGCGAAUUCUGUGAAUUCUCCUCCGGCUACAUCCAGAGCAUCAGGCGUCAUUACCGGGACAAGCAUGGUGGGAAGAAGCUUUUCAAGUGCAAAGACUGCUCCUUUUACACAGGCUUUAAAUCUGCUUUUACUAUGCACGUGGAAGCUGGGCACUCAGCAGUUCCCGAGGAGGGCCCCAAAGAUCUUCGCUGUCCUCUCUGCCUCUAUCACACCAAAUACAAGCGCAACAUGAUUGACCACAUCGUGCUGCACCGAGAAGAGCGUGUUGUCCCCAUUGAAGUUUGCCGGUCCAAACUGUCCAAAUACUUGCAGGGAGUAGUUUUCCGCUGUGAUAAGUGUACCUUCACCUGCUCCAGUGAUGAGAGCCUCCAGCAACAUAUAGAAAAGCACAAUGAACUGAAACCUUACAAAUGCCAGCUCUGCUACUAUGAGACCAAGCACACGGAGGAACUGGACAGCCACCUUCGGGAUGAGCAUAAGGUAAGCCGUAACUUUGAGCUGGUUGGACGGGUUAACUUGGAUCAGCUGGAACAGAUGAAGGAGAAAAUGGAGAGCUCCAGCAGCGAUGAUGAGGACAAGGAAGAAGAAAUGAACAGCAAGGCUGAAGACAGAGAGCUGAUGAGAUUUUCUGACCACGGGGCUGCUCUUAACACUGAGAAGCGUUUUCCAUGUGAAUUUUGUGGACGGGCGUUUUCACAGGGCUCUGAGUGGGAAAGACAUGUGCUGAGACACGGCAUGGCAUUGAAUGACACCAAGCAGGUGAGCAGAGAAGAAAUCCACCCAAAAGAGAUCAUGGAGAACAGUGUUAAAAUGCCCUCCAUAGAGGAAAAGGAAGAUGACGAGGCCAUUGGGAUAGACUUUUCCCUAAAGAAUGAAACAGUAGCCAUCUGUGUAGUAACUGCCGACAAAUCUCUCCUGGAGAAUGCAGAGGCCAAAAAAGAAUGAGCGUUUGGUGAAAUUCUUAAUCAAACCUUACUUGAACAGUGAUGAAAAAGUGGGAGGGCUGGCUUGGGCUGAGAAGGGAGGGACAGAAAAGAGAAGACAGAACAAAGCUGCUUUUUAGGACUGAACAAUCUAUUUUCAAAGCACUGGUACCUGUGUGAGUGAGUAUGUAAAUUAAAGUUAUUUAAAUGGUUGGAAUAUGUGGCUCCUUUUCCAUCACUACAUCUUUUCUUCCGGAUCUUCAUCAUGGAAGUUUCAUUUGUUGCGGAAUAUGGAAGCACCUCCCAAUGGUACGGUGCACCCUGUGGUGGUCUUGGACAGUAUGUGGAAACAGAAGCUCCAUGACGGUAGAAGACUUCUCAUUGGGGAGCAACUUUUUGACGCACAACUUUUGGUGCGUUUUUCUAGUUUUAAUACCUUAAGCUUUUUCAAGACCUAACUGCAGCCGCUUUGGGAAAAAAAAACAAAAAACAAAAAACAGAAAACAAAAAAAAAAAAACUGCUUUGCAUAAAACAGUCACCUGUUUCCUAGUACCUCAAACUUAACCAAGGGAACUCUCUGCAUUUGUCAGUACUACCUGUCGUCGUUGUGGUUAAAUGUAGAGAGAACUGCUGGGCAAGAUGGUGAAUGGAGAAAAAAAAAGAGUUUUAAAGAAAGGAACACAAAUUGUGCUUAAAAUCCCCAUGUGGGUUUUAUUUCUUAAAAUACUGUGAUUUUUUUAAUUAUUUUAGUAAAAAACAAAACAAAAAAAAGAAACAGACUUUAAUUAUUAGAUAACUGUUUGUGAAUUGUCAUCCUUUAUUCCAGGUAAGCUGUUUAUUAGUGUUCAACUAUAAUUUAGAAUUUGGUAGAUUCAUGUGAGCUAAUUUUAAGGUGAUUGUGGAGUUUUGUUUGCCACAUGUUUAUUUUCUAUCAAUUUGAGUGUUACAAACACAGCACAAUUCAGUUUUUCAUAUGAAUUGUUUUUCGUGUGUGUGUUGUUAUUGUUGUUUUAAUUUCGGGGCAAGGGAGAUUUAGUUUUUUGUGAAUAGGAAUGUUUUUAUUUUAAACAUGGAAAUAACAAAGAAGUUAACUUUCUUUUUUUUUUUUUUUUUUUUUUUUAAUUUAACUAAAGAACCAAACUUUCGGCACAGCUAUGCAGCUUGUGGGCCAGACGAGGAGGUCCUCCUCACCCUUUUGUUGCCUGUCAAAUUCACGCAUUAUCCGUCUCAUAAAUAAUUUCUGUUAGGAUUGGCUGGCUUUUGUGUGUGAUUUUAAAAUCUGUGUUUUGUUUCUGCUGGCAUUGUGUUUUGUUGGGGGUUUUCAUUUAUUUAGGGGACGAGGGGAUGUACUAGAAUCCCAUCCCUUUCGUGAGAGUGGACAAGAAAUAACAUAUCCUACAAGGAGCCUGGAGAACUACUUUCUUUCUUUCUUUUUUUUUUUUUUUUUUUUUUUUUAAAUCUAGCUGCCAGCUGCUCUGUCCCCCAUAUCAGCUUUUUCAGGAGGGAGCAGCUUAGACUAAAUCUAAGCCUACAUUUAUAAUAUGUUCUGAUUGUGAACAAAGGGUUUCGUUCCAAAAAAUAGAAAAGAACUUUUCUUGAAGCCUAGGUUUUAGAAGCCCGUGUGUGUGUGUGCUUGGAUGUGUGUGUGCGUGUAUGAGUGUGUGUGUGCAUGUGUGCACGUGUGAAUCCUUUGGUUUUCAUGUUUUUUUUUUUUUUUUUUUACUUGGAAGGGUUGUGGGAGGGUGGGAGGGAAGAAAGGGAAGGGGAAUUGCUGAGAUGACAGUGUCCCACACAGCUUCAAAUAAAAUCCAUGGAAAGAUGUUGCAUUUGUGGAAUAAGUGCUUACUUGAAAAGCAUGUUCUUCUUUUAUUUUCUUACUGUUAAGAAUUUUUAUUUGUAGGAUGUUUGUUUUAAUUUAAUUUUUUUAAGGGAUGGGGGCCAUCAUGUGGAAACCAGAAAAUGGGGAAAGUGUGAACUAUCCAGACAAAGAUUCAUUUUGUGUCUAUAUUUGUUUUUAAUUGGCCUCAUUUCAAAUGUAUUAAACAGUUCCAUACCUGGAUUGGGUGUUUGUAAUGGUUACCAAAAAACAAACAAAAAAAGAAAGAAAAAGGAAAAAAAAAAAGAAAAUAAUUGUGACAUGCUUUUAUCACUACUUUAUUUUUCAAAUAACAUGUAAAUAUUGUAAUCCAUUGGAUUUUGUUUUGCUAACCUGUUAAUAAAAAUAUGGGACCAUUAUCCUUUUAACAAGGCUAGAAUGUCAUUUUUUUCUUUUUCAAACAUAUACCUGAUAUUUUGUGGCCGCACAUUUUGGAUGCAUUAUUAUAAUUCUGUUGACUGUAAUGACAUAGAAUUUACAACAUUUUUUGUUGUUGUUUAAUUUAUACAGAGGACAUUUUUUUCAGAGCUUGAGAGAAGAAAAUAAAUAGCAAAAUGAUAACCUAUUGACUCCAGUAAUCAGUGUUUCCCAAUACUUCAUAAGAGAUAGGGAGACCCUGAGUCCUUGAAGCCAAGGGUUUAAAAACAAAACAAAAACAAAAAAAACCACAAGUAGGUUAUUCAAGUUGUUUGCAACAUACAUUUUGUAAUGAAAUGUGAGAAAUUAAUAAAGAAUUUUUUUCACAUGUG